ACAAAGGAAAUGCCCUCACUCAGCUACAAGUGCCUCCUGCUCCGUGCGGGGCCUCAGGGCCCCAGAGCCCCGCACCAGCUCUGACUUCUCGUGGUUCCUGGGGAUCUUGGCAUCGUCCUUAAAAAUGGCUUUUGUUUGGGAUCCUCUGGGAGCCACGGUGCCAGGACCAUCUACAAGAGCCAAAUCAAGAUUGCGUUUCUCAAAGUCCUACAGGUAUUACUCUUUUCCUUUUGUAGCUAGGAAGAAUUGUUUAACUGCCUUAGGCCCCUUGCAAAUAAGCCUUUGCCCUAUGUUGACCUUCUAACUCCUAAUGCUUGUUAAAUUGACAAUAUAUUAAAUAAGAGCCAAGAAGAUGAUGUAAACCUUGAAAUAGGGGUAUGUAGGUACGUGCAGAAGUUGAAGGAAGUUGACUAACUUUAAAAGCUAAUUCUGAGAGUUAAAUGGCAAACUUAACAAAGCAUUCAUAUUACUGCCACCUGAAAAACAGUGUAUUAACUUGUCUAAUGGCUUAAUACAGUCAACUCUAAAUGUUAGGGAAGGGUUCUUGUUUGACCAACAAAAAAAACACUACAUUAUUCUUCAUAAGUGUUUCAGGGCACAUGCACAUGAAAAAAUGGAAACUAAUGCUGUUUCAGGUAGUAAUUCAGUGUUCAUCUUGCCCAGCAGAAUUACAUGUCAUGAAUUCAAACUAAAUAUUUUAAUAAUCUUUUGUUUCUGGAAGUCAUAUUAAAAAUCUUGACCUCAUGACUUCACUAAACUGUCAAUGACUGUUUUACAACAAAAUCAGCUUAUUUUAACCAAAUAACUGGAAAGAAAGAAAACACUUAAAAAAUAUUGGAUUUCCUUCUUCAUUUGAGUAUUCUAGGUGUUAAUAAAGAGAAGAUUGAUUAUUCUUUAUUAUUGUUUAGAAAGAAAACCUUUUCUGUUUUUGAUUGAUUACAAUCUAUAGCACUGAAAGGUAUCUAUUUAAUCAAUAGUAAAUAGAAGUGACAUUGUUUGCAAAAUUUUGGAUAUAAGGUCUUUCUUAUUUAGACCAAAUGCAGCACAUCUGGAAGCUGCCAAGCCUAUGUAGAAAUAUAUAUUAACACUGAAUUAAAAUGUGUUCUGAUUUGCCUGCAUAUAAAACAUUCAAAGUUUGAAUUAAAAUAAUUUAUAAGGAUUAAUUAUUUGCUUUAGACACUAAAGAAGAUAAUGUCCUUGGAAUUUUUAGGGAACUAUAAAAUCAGAGAAAUCAAAUUUAAAAAUUUUGUAUAACAAUGCAUAAGCAAACUUUGGCAAGAGGUAAAUAUAAUUUGCCAGCUAAAGGUAUAGGUAUUAACUCCAUUUAUUUUUAUUUCAAAAUAAAAUAAUGAUUUAUUUGUUAUGUUUGUUACAGCUAUAAAAUUUAGUUGAAAAUUUUAAAUUAUAUGCUUCCUAUGUGCUUUGCAUUUUGUUAAAUGUGAUUCUCAUGCUUAUUGUAUGCUAAAUUGUACAUUUAGAACUUAACAUCAAUGAUUUGCUAACAUUACUGUGCAUAUUUCCAACAUAUGGUGGCUUCUAGGCUCUCUUCAUCACUAGAUCUGAUAACAAGCUCCUUAAUAUCAUAAAUCUCCAGCUGCUGAAUAAAGUAAAAGCAAUAGCUUGAUUGACUAAUGAAUUUGAGAAAUCUCACGAAAUGCAGAGUUUAAGCUCUUCUGUGUAGUUUGCAAAUAUAUUAUAAACCUUGCCUUCUCAAUUUGGCAAAGAUAUUUUUAUUUUGAGGUGUUAUGGUAUUGUAACAAUUUAAAGCUAUAUGAUAAAUAUAUUUUUUCAAGGUUCCUUUGGUCAAGUUCUGACCCUUUCCAAAAUAUAAGCAUUAGCAGCUAAGAAUGACUUUUUCAUGUAUUUGAAUACCUCACAUCUGUAAUUUUAACAAGUUUCAUUUGUAACAAGUUUAAGAGGUGAGAAUGACAUCUCAAAUAUCCAUCAUGAGUCAGUUUCCUUCGGAAGCUUGAGAGGCUCAGUCCUUCCUUUACUUCCUCUUAAUUUGAAUAUACAAUUUCCCACAGAAUAAUUAAUUUUUUUAUAUGUGCUGCUUUCACUGUUUGGAGGUUCUAGUUUAUCUUUCCAGUUGCACUGCAAACUCUUUGAGGUUAGAAGUUUCCUUACAUACAGCAAAAAUGCCAGUAAUGCCUAUUUGAUAAAGUAUUCUGUUACCCUUUCUUAUUUGGCAUCACCCGAUAAUGUUUUAUUGGCAUAGCCAACUUGAUAUGAUCAUAUCUAUCAUAAGUUGAAUUGAGUGGAAGGGUUAGGGAGGUAGGAAGGCAGUUGGCCACUGGCUCUUGCAUUUCUGCAGGUCCCUCAUGUAUCCAAAGGAGAUUACGCAUUCAGCCACGACAAUGUACUGACAAUAAUGAAAAAAGGUACAUAUCAUAUAACUUAAAAUUUUUAUCAUACCAUAAUACCUCAAAUGCACCAUGAGUCACUCUAUAUAUAUACAGACACAUAUACACACCACACACAGGCACAUGCACGCACAGUUAAAUGCUAUAAUUAUCUUCUGAAGAGCAUAGUUUUAUUGCAUAGCAUUCUUGGAAUUAAAGGUGUUAAACUAUUUGAUGUAAACAUGUAAAAUAUCUCAUAAUGUCACAGCCUUGUUUUUGCAUUUCUUAUUUUUUAAAAAAUAUACAAAAUCCUUACGCGGUGAAAGUAACUUAAGCUUAUCUUGACCUUUAAGAGGCUUUGGAUCUGAUUCCAUUAUUGAAGCAACUGAAAGAACUGGACAUUGGACAACAUUUCUUCAUUGAAUUUCUCCCUUAUAAUUUUUUUUAUGAGCAAUAUUUUUUAUCUUGUAAAAUCUUCAAAUGUGCCUAUUGUAGUGUCAUUUUUCUUUGGCUAUUGAAUGGAUAAUAAUGCAUGCUACUGGGGGUACACUUAGCUUUAACUGGAAUAUUUUUCCUUGGCAUGGCUUUUGCUGCCUGGUAAUAUUCAGGCUAAAGGAAAGCCAGGUGUACAAGAUAUGAAAUUCAAUUAGUGUCUGAUUUGUUAAAGUAAUAGCAAAUCAUAUACAUUUAAUGAGUGUUGACUCUUGAGAAAUACAAUCUGAAACAGUUUUACAAUGCUCAAAAUAGAUGUGAAAGUUUUUCAGCUGUGACAAUUUUUUAUCUUAUGUGGGUAAAAUACAUUUUUAUAAGAAAAGAUUAAUAUAUAGCUUAUUAAGUUUGAUUGAGGCAGAAAGAAGGAUUGAAAGAGAAAAGAAGAGGGAGAGGGAAGGAAAGGCAGGGGAGAGGAGGGGAGCAGGGCCGUGGAAGGAGGAGUGAGGAAGAGAAAAAGAGAGAAAGCAGAGGGUUACAUAAUAAGGAAGGUACUUUUUCUCUGUGAGCCCAGAAGAGAUUGCCAACCAUGUUUUCAGUAAUGGGAUCAGUGUUAGCAUUAGGGCACCACUUACAAAGAUGAGUACUAAUUUUGAGGGCAAGGUGCUGAUUUAUCUGCCUAGGUUCUGGCACACAUGUUUAAAGAUUCACCUAAUUACUUUAGAGCAACGCCCCUCCCAAGUAUUAUAGAGAAGAAAGAGGAGAAUGAUGUGCUCAAGAAAACAAUGUGGAGAAGUUUAUAUUGGUUGUUUAAACAUAGUACCUAAAAAAAAAAAAAUGGGGAAAAACGAUCUGGGAAGUAAAGAAAGAAUCAAGGAGCAAAGAUUUAGCAAGCCUGUGGACCCUGACAACUCCAAUAAGAGAACACUAGGGAAUUUUGUGAUUUAAAAUAUAUUAUUGCUUAAAACUACAGUAGUGUUCAAGGAAACUUUAAAUAGAAAAUUACUCUUCUUGAGAUGAUUCUGUCUUCCAAAGAGAACAAAUCACAAGGAUGUUAAAAGGAACAUUUUAUGUGACAAGUUUGGGGUAGGUACUAUGUAAAUAGAAGAGAAAGUCACUCAAGGUACAUUUGAAUGUAGGGCAGAGAUUAUUCCAUAGCAUUCCACAGGCCAGAAACAGAAAGUGUCUUCUAGUUUUCUUGCCCUUUAUAGUAAUAGGGGUCAUGGGAUAGAAAUUCUCAGAAAAUCUCCAAAUCUCAUUUUUGCCAAUUGUUUCAACAUCUUUUCCUUCCCAGCAUUUUAGCAGAGCUGCCAAACAGGUGAUUAAUUAAAUACAUAUGUGCAUGCUUGUACCUCGUGUAGAAGGUCUAAUGAGUAAAUUUAUUUGAUAUGACAUAGACUGAACAGUAGAAGGAAGGAUUAAUGACAGUCAGAUCAACAAACAAAAGUACAAAUGGUAUCUGGGCUAUGAAAAGAUAAAGCAAUAUUUGCCCAAACAAGAAGAUCUAGAUAUCCCUAAAUUACCUCCUAUAUUAUUAGGAAGUAAAGACCAAAUCUACAACUUUGAUCUGGAAAUUGUAUAGUAGCUGAUAUGAACAGGGAUCAUAGGAGAGUGUGGUCUCAUAGCUACUCUUUGCUACUACCAAAACCUGAGUGGUAGCACAUCAGUGAUUGCCCAACCAAACUGCACAAUUCCCAUUAGAAAAAGCUGUCUCAAACCCACAUCUUAGAAAGGAAGUGAAUGCCACCAGUGAAUCAAUACACUGGGAUGUAACUUUCUGCAUACCCCAAGAAUACCUCCUGUUGCAUAGCACUUUUUAGUUUUCAAAGCUUUUCAGAUGUAACAGAUGUGACAGCUGUUGUUUUUAGUGUGCCACAGCUCAUCUCACUUAAUUCUUUAGGGUAAGUGAAAAAGAUGAGUGUAAUUAGUAUCAAAUAAGAGAAGAAGAAUUGAAGGUUCAGGGACUAGAGACCACACAUAUAUGUGGUUAGAAAGUCCAAAGUAAGAACAGUAGAGCUAGUUUGUAUUGGACACUUACUAUGCACCAGGAACCAUUCCCAAUCCCAUACAUGCAUUAGCUCAUGCAUGUCAUCCUCCAAAACAGCCUCGGGAGGUGGAUCUAGCAUUACCUUUAUCUUACAAAUGAGGAAACCAGGCAGAGCAAGUUUAAGAAACCUGCACAGGUGUGAAUUCUGGAAGUCUGUGUUAGAACCAGGACUCCUGGUCCCUCUCCCACCUCCAGCUUCCUCACCAGAUCCUAUUAUCAGCACACAAGGAAAAAAAUUCCAUAAUGAGAGGUAUUGUUCUAACAGAUGUACUAUCUUCCUCUACUUAACUCUGAAUUUUUCUCUGAAGACAGAACACCACGUAAUUUGUUAUAGAAUAGGGCUUAGUAAUCAGUUAAAAUAUAAACUUGUUAAAUAAUAUCUAAACUGUCCUCUAACCUAAUUGAUGUUGGUUUAAAGAAAUGCUAAGCAAAAGCAUCAAAAUAGAGGUAUUUUUAUAUUAAAAAGAAGAAAAAGGAAAAUGAAUCCGUUAUUUUAUAUUGUCUGCUUCUGCCCCCUCCUGGCUUUUGCUUCAUGGGCUUCCAUCUGGCUCAUUUCAUCUGGCCAAAAACAUUGGUCAUGUGGUUGUAUUUUACUGCCAAAUAUUACUCCUUGGCCAGCUGUUCAGAGGAGCCAGAAGAUUCUCUGAGCUCGAGAGGUCAACUCCAUCCUGUGUCAUGUCUAUUUAUUCUACUGGCAUAGUCUUGACUAUUAAACUAGGUUUCUUAAUGAUAUUUCAAAUUGUGAGUAAUGUUGGCUAAAUUGACAAAAAGAAAUUAUAGACAACAUUUAUAUCUAAGAAUAACAAUACUACUAACAACCAUUGCACAUUGUAGGAAGAGGUAGCAUGGUAUAGGAGGAGAACUUUGGCUCUAGAGCCAAACAGACCCAGCUUCAGUGCCAACUCUGCUGCUUUCUUGAUUGGGCAGGUUUCCUAACCUCUCUGAGCCAUUUCCAUGUACAUAAAUAGAAAAUUAAAAUAUCUACUUCAUAAGGUCGUUGUGCAGAUUAGAUGAAAGCAUGUACGUGAAUGCAGGACUACCUGCCAACUCUUUCAUAGCAUUUUCCAAGUCUUCACUAACAUUUCACAAAUUUUGUGAAGCUUCUUUUGUGAAAUACAUUUUCAGAUAAACUAUCAUCAUUGGUACCACUCUUGGUCACAGAAUAGUACAAUAGAGCUGGCUUAUAAAUGGUUACCUUAUAAGCAACUUGCACAUACAACCCAGGCUCACCUUGGAAAUGUAGUGUGCAGGAAUGAUUGACAGCUGGCUAGCUCUACAGCCACACUGCUGCUGAGGUUCACAUUUUCACAUUAUCACUUAUAGCUAUGAGACUUUGGGCAAGUUACUUCAUGUGCCUCAGUUUCCUCAUUUGUAAAAUGGAGUAUUAUGAGGAUUAAGUGUGUUAGCCAUGUAAAGUGCCUGGCACAUAGACAACACUAAAAUAAAUGUCAGCUAUUAUUAAUAAUAGAAUGUAAGCUCCACAUGGCAGCAAUUUUUGUCCUUUUUUCCACCUUUGUAUGGCCAGUGCCUGGAAGAGUGUGUGGUACAUAUUAGGUGCUUGGCGUUUGUGUAUUGAAUGAAUGAACCUAUUAGCAAAUGUGUUCCGAUUCAUGGCAAGUGUGAGGAUACUCUGCUUCCUUUUGCCACAUUCAUGGGAAGAGGGGGUUAGAGCUGAAGGAACCUGAUGGUUCAUUUGUUCAAACUCAUUUGUCUUACAUUGAAGAGCUUGAAGACCUUGAAAGGCCCCAGGGUCAUGCAACUUGAUAGCGGCCUGGUCAGAGCUAGAACCCUGGCUCUGUGUGCUUCUGUGAAAAUCUUUGUUCCAAUGUCCCACCCCUCACUUCAAUACAUAUGCCAUCUAAUUCAGUGCUUUCAGUAAGGCAGCAAAAUGAAUGAAUGAUUCAGAGCACACUUCUUGCAGACAGGAGAGUGUAUAAGAGCCAUAAUUGGGCAAUGACCAUGGAAGGACAGGUUUCUGAAUAAGAGAAAGACUUAUCCAAGUAAAAUUAUGUUCAGACAUUUUACUUACAAGUCUAAAAAUCACUUGCUACAACAGCUACAAUAGGGUUUUUGUAAGGAAGUACCACUUUGUAAACAACAUUUUUGUAGAAUGCAUUAUAUGCAUUUUUUUCAAAAUUGAAGGAAAGCCCCAUCUCAAACAUUCAAAAGAAUCUGCUCAAUUAUCAAUGUAGACUAGAAACAGAGAUAGAGAGGGGAGAUACAGUUUGAGUGUUUUCUGUAUUAUCAUGACAGCACAUGGAACAACCACAGGCAGAAAGAUUACAAACUCUGCAAUAAAUAUAAAGGUAUUGGUUUUAUAAGGUGGCCUGCAGGCUACGGACCAGCACAGAGCUCUGGCAAAUGUGGAAUGCCAGGAGAUGUACAAAAAAAUCAAGGUGACAAAAGAAGAAAAGACACUCCAAACUGCCAAGGGUUUAUAAUCAUGCUGUGGAUAUUUCUGAUCAUCAGUGUGUUAAUGGUUUUCACUAUAGUUAAAACUAUACCAUUUUUGAAUGGGUAAUAGGUAUGAAUAUUUAUGCUUAAUUAGUAGUUUAUAAAAUUUAUACUAUUUAUUUUCAUAAUGUUGAUUUUAUGAUUUUCAACGAGUGCCAUUUGUCCUUAAGUCAUGAAGUGGAUGAGCCCCCAUCAAGUGAUUUUAAGAGACAGUACCUUGACUGAGCAGCUGGAUCAAAGCCUGUCUGAUCUGGGCAGAGCAAAUAAGGAAUACUUCUUACAAAAGAGGAAGCAUUCAAUUCUAUACACUUUACCUUGGUACUCCUUGUUCUGGAGGCCUCAGCUUCUAUCAUGUUCUUUGCCACAGUCAUAUACCCACCUUCUACCUUGGCUCUCCCUCCUCCUAACUUCCAUUAUUUUUUCUACUUUCAAACUAUAAUUGACAAGCCUUUUUAAUUUCAACAAGGGUCUGAAGAGAGGUGUCUGAUUUUCCGUAAGGCUGGGUUAUAUAAGCACACAGAGUUGAAUCAGAGCAAAGGAAAAAUCCAUUGGCAAAGGAAGAAUACUAUAUGCUACUUUAAAACUUGUCUGAAUGUAUUAUUUUAUUUACUUAUUUUAGAGGCAGGGUCUCACUCUGUCAUCUAGGCUGGAGUACAGUGGCAUGAUCAUCACUCAUUGCAGCCUCAAACUCCUAGGCUCAAGGGAUCCUCCAGCCACAGCCUCCUGGGUAGCUAGGACUACAGGUGCACCCUACCAUUCCUGGCUUAAAAAAUAUAUAUUUUAGAGUCUGUUUUGCCCGGGUUUGUCUCAAAUACUUGGCCUCAAGUUAUCCUCCCACCUCAGCCUCCUAAAGUGCUGGGAUUACAGGCAUGAGCCAUGGCACAUGGCUCAAAUUAUAUAAUUCAUUAGCUGGUAAUAGUGUAAAUUUGGAAGAGAAAAACUAAAAUGAUAAAGAGGAAAGAUGGAUUGUGAAUAGAGUAAAUAUAUAUUACUGUAAUUAUGUUAAGCCAAUCAAAUGCAAAGGACAGUUCAAAGGGGACAAGUAUGUAAGCCACAUUCCAAAAAAAAAAAAAAAGCUUUGAAGUGAAGCUUUAAAAAGAUAAGCUUUGUGUUGAGCUAAAGAAAUAAACUCUAUAAAAACAAAACCCUAAAAUUGUUAUGACAAUGAAUUAAACAUUCAAAAAUGAACAGAACAGAAUGUAAAAGAUUAUUCCUUCAGGUGGUAAAUGUUCACAACCAGCUCUCUAUGGGGGAGGGGAAGGGCACUAUUUGUAGUAUUUGCUGAUUUCUGUGCCAAAAAAUUCUCUCACCUGCCCAUUUCAAACAGCAGAGGUCACUAAAUGUGGAGUUGGCAAGAGAUACAUAGACAUAGUACUCUAUACAGUGUUUCUAUCAUAUAGAUACAGUAGAUAUAAGUUGCCCCAAAAACAUAAUAAUACAAAAUGUAGCCAAAUCAUUCAGAAGUUAUGAGUUUUGAAUACUUAUUUCCAUUGUUUUUAAUAUAAUUUGUUUAAUUAUAGUUAAAAAUUUUUAUGUAAUUUAAUUUUUAAUAACUGUUGGGUAUUAACAACUGACUUAUAAAUACUCCUAAAAAUGUAACAGAAUGUAGUGAGGGACAAAAUGGAUGCGGUCUCUGCUUUCAUCAAGUUUACAUUCUGGUAGAGAAAGACAGAAAAUAAACAAGUUAACAAUAAAUAAAAUAAAUAGAGACUGAGAUGAGAGGUUCUGCUUGGGGAAGCCAGGGAAACCUUUACAAAGAAAUUGAUAAUUUAUUUGCAUAUAAGUUCAAGCAUAUCCAUUCCAUACAUCUGUGAGUACAUUUGUAGUUCUAGGCCUGAAACUCAGAACUGCACAAGGUCAAUGGAACCAUAUAAAUAUUGACCUCAUUACUGACUUGUUUUCAGUCUCCAGUCUCUUGAGUGAAUUUACCUUUGCUUCUUUGUUAUUAUAAAAAUACAGUGAGGGAAAGUAAAACAAGGAGGAAGAUGAAAAGAAGAUGUAGGGGGAAGAGGAGCAGUUUACAAUAUACUUUCUAUUACAUUGUUUCACACUAUCUCAAAACUUUUUAUACGUAGAAAAUACUAAAGCAAAGAAAAAUGGAAGUUAAAAAUCGGUAGCAGUAGUAAUAGUCCUAUAGUAGGAACCUUGUUUUGUUUGAAAUAUGUGUCUGUGUCUGCCUACAAAACAUAAACACCUUAAGCUAAGAAUAACUGUGAGAUUAAUUUUUUAUUUUCAAAGAAAUAAUACAAAUUUUAAAUCUUGCAUUAAAAGGAAAGCUAGCUGGACGAAACUUUUCUGACACACAGAUUUUGAGAAUAGCACCCAUAAAUAUGCUUCCAAUGCUUGUCACUUGAUCCCUUUUUGGCAAUUAACUUGCCUUUAAUUGAUUUGUGGAUUACCCACUGGAAGUUGCUAUGGAUAAAGGAAUGUAAUGGCAGAGUUUGUUUAUAUAGGGUAACAAAAUAGACUGGCUGGGAGGAGGGAUUUAACUGCAAAAUAUCCUUGAUUUUCAGGAAUUUUUCUUUUCACAUAAUGGCAGUGUUUAGAUAAAGAAUGGAAAGUUAAUGAAUCAGAUUUGUGUUCCCAUCCAAAGGGAAGAUUUAUGUCCUGUUUAAGAAUCACAUUAAUUUGAUGACGUUAGUACAUUCUCUAGUGAAAGAGUGGCCACUUUAGUGGAGGAAAAAAACAAGCAACAAAACUCCUUCUGCCAUCUUCAGGUUGUACCUGACGAAAAGCUUUUAUUUGUGGGUUCUAUGAAGUAUCACUGCCCUGAUCUCAGAUGAACUAAAAGAUGAAAACAUUUCAUCGCUCAAAUAAUUGUUUAUCUCACAUCUUACUGGUUCUAGAAAAGGACUAUAUAUUUUCCCUCCUAACUUUCCUCAGUUUCUUGGUAUAAAGUUCAAAAUGCUUUGAGUAGAGUUGUUCAGGAGGUCCUCAGUGGCACUGCCACUCACUGGUUGGGACGUUUUUGUUCUCUGUCCUCCUGUGUGGAAGAUGACAAGGACGGCUUUGUGCAACUUCUGUUGUAUGCGCUGCUUUUCAACCCCUUGGAUGAGAUACUCAUACAAGGAACGUCAGGUUUUUUUCCUAAAGCAAAUCCGUGUAAACUGAGACAACAUAAACCUUAGGGAGAUCUGACACACCAAAAUGCCAAGAAAGGGAAAGAAGAAAUUAUUAUCGGUGGGGGAAACAAAUUAUCCUGUAUUUUGGAGUGAAUUUAAAAGGCUUAUUGUUUGUUUUAGCACUACAUGACUUAAAAAAAAAAGUCUCGCAGUCUUGCCUUCCUCAUGUUGGUUAAAAUGGAAAGGAUUCUCUUUCUUUGCUAUUUAUAGAUAACCCUUAGCACUCUGCAAGGAUCUAUUUGGUAUAAAAUGAUGGGUGUGAAUGUGCCAGUAAGAGAGAAAAAAAUGCUUAGCCAUAUUUACUCAUAUAACCAACAUCUAGGUCAAAAUCAAAAUAUUACCAGCUCCCAAGGGGACCCCUUUAUUCUUCUUUCCAGUCACUAUGCACCCGAAGAUAACCACUAACUGACUUCCAAUAGCAUAGAUUUGACUACUUUUGAAUUUUAUAUGAAUGAAAUUAUACAAUAUAAACUCUUAUUUUAUUUCAGUCAAUAUUGUGUUUAUGGGAUUCAUUCAUAGUGUUUUGUGCAUUCUUUAUUCUCAUUUUGUUAGUAUUGCACCAAAUGAAUAUGCUACAAUUUACUUAUUCUAGUGUUGAUGGAUAGUUAAGUAUUCCAGUUUUAGGCCAUUAUGAAUUAGAGCCAUUAUGAACAUUAUUGGAUAUAUCACUUAGUAAACAAAUGUACAUGUAGUGUUGCAGUGUUUUGUGCAUACACGUAGGUUGGGUAUAUCCCAAGAGGUAGGAUUUCUGGGUCAUAGGUUAUGCCUUUGUCUUUAGAUAUUGCCAAAUGUGUUUCUAUACUGGUUGCCACAUUUAUGUCGCCCCCAAAGUGAUGUUUCAGUUCUCUGCAUUCUUACCAAAGUAUAGGUCAUCCAUUUUCAGUGAUGGCAUCUUAAAAAAUGUUUGCCUGUAAUAACAAUGUCAUCAUGCCUUUUAUUUAUGCAGUUGAGUCUUUUAAUCUUUAGGACCUGUUUUUCCAGGAAUAGUGUGGGUAACAGUGAGCCAUUCACACUCUGUCUGUUUCUCCUCAUGAUGAAUACUAUGUAACUGUGAAUUAAGUGACUAAAAUAAGAAACGAUCUGAUAUGCAGAAAUAGAGUUUUCCCUGUUUGAUCCAUAUGCAGCUUAAAUAUGUGAUGUUAUUCUACAUUUUAUCCAGAUUCAUUUUUCAAACCAAUAGUAAUCAUUGUUAGCAAAAACCAAUAAAUAAUCUUUUAUUCUGUUUUAAAAUUUCCAUGUCGUACUUUGAGUUCUUGCUAUAUAUCCCGUGCUCACUUUAAAUCAGGUUUUCCUUCCCGUACAUUAUUUCUUGGAAAAUAUGUUUUGGACUUUUCCUAAACCACCUUAACCUGUUGAAAAACACUAGUAAAUGCAUAGGCAGUGUAAGUCACGCUAAAAUAAAUGUGUAUUGCUUUUUCAAGAUUUUGUUUACCCAUGCAUUUAAAGAAGGUUUUUUUCCCUUUAUUUUCUUUCUUUUUUGUCAUUAUAGUCAUUAUGUCUUUUUAAUGUUAAGAUUCCGGUAAUAUAUAUUCCUCAUUUUUAUGUCAUCUCCAAAGCUCCCCAUAACUGAUUGAUGAUAUCAAUCCGGCUUCUGGCAUAUAAAGUUUGUUGACCUGGUUCAGUUUGUACCAUGUCAAAAUGUGAUCAUUAAUUAUUAGAUGAUGUCAGGAAAAAUUUAGUAUGUGUGAUAACUGUGGGUCCCAUUUCUUAAAGCUUUCAAAAUCCAAUCUUAAGGCUCUCUACUUUGUGGCAUAUGAGGGAACAUAAGUAAACAUUAGAGCAAUAUCAAACGUAUUCUAAGGGUUUCAUGAUGUGAAACAAUAUAUCACUUUAUUACCAGACAGAUACUUCACAUCGUGAAAUUUGAAAAAGCAUACGAGGUGGGGCACAGUGGUUUACCCUAUAAUCCUAGUGCUUUGGGAGGGUGAGGUGGGAGGAUCGCCUGAGUCCAAGAGUUUGACACCAGCCUGUGCUACAGAGUGAGACCCCAUUUCUACAAAAAAUUUAAAAAUUAGUAGGGUGUGAUGGUGCCUGCCUGUAGUCUCAGCUACUCUGGGGGCUGAGGGAGGAUUGCUUGAGCCUGGGAGGUCAAGGCUGCAGUGAAUGUGAUCACAGGAGUGUACUCCAGCCUGGGCAACAGAGUGAGACCUCAUCUCUGAAAAAAAGAAAAAGUAUGUAAUUUUUACGUAAGAGUCACUCGAUUCAUAUCAUGAAGCUUGUGCUAAAAAUGGAAUCAUUCAGUGAUCAUGGGCUGCUUUUCAAGCAUUUUUCGCUCACCCUUUACCAUUAUGACAGUAAACUUUGGGGAAAGGGGAAGGCAUGGGCCAAUACAUCUUUUAGUAUUUCUUGGUUAUACUAAGAACUACUGAGGAACUGCUAAGGAACAACUACAUAGAUAAAAAGUAUUUUUAUUAUAACCCUUGUGAAAAACCUCUUCCCCCAUAAAACGUUUAGUAUCUUGUAUGAAGGCAUAAUGUACUUUUAAAUAUUCAAAUCCAAUUCCAGAUUUCAUUUAUGUGCUAUGUACUGUGUAAUCCACCACGCAAAAUGUAAUUUCUUGCUUUUAAUAUAAAUUUUCAUUAUUAUCAUAAAUGAAGUCUCAGACCACAACAUUUUGUUAGGUUGCAUUCAAAUGGUAAUCAUAAUAUGACCUAUACCAGUUUUUGCAUGGAAGGGCAGCAGCCGGCUGAACUAGAUUUCCACUUUUGUCUUGGCUCAUUAAACAACAAUGGACAAGUUACCUUAACUUCAUGGGUCCUCAACCUUCUCAUUCGAAAUUGAGUGUAUGGACUGUAUAUUACAAUAUCCUUUUAAGCUUACAGAAAUAACAUUAUGGAGGUAUGAGAAAAUUGUAAAUGAUCCAAGAUAUGUGCCUAAAUAUUUCUUCAUACAUCAAGCAUGCAUUCAUGAAAUCAACACCAAGCCCAGGAAAUAUCAAAGAAUAGCUCAAUGUCCCUGUGAACUUAUAUCCAAUUCAAUAAUUCAUCCAACAAAUGUAUAUUGAGUAUAUAAUCUGCUAGACUUAUGAAGCCUUAAACUUUAUGCUGUACAUUCUGAUAUAUGUUGUUUUAACCAGGGGUUGGUCAGCUUUCAAAAGUGACCCUUUUGCUAACAUUGUUCUUCUGGCUGAAAGCUAGUAAGUAUAAGCAAAAGGAGAGAUGUAUAUGAUCUCACUUCUAUGUGGAAUCUAAAAAAGUCAAACUCACAGAGGCAGAUAAUAGAAGGGGGUUACCAGGGGGUGAUGGGAACAGGAGGGAUUGGGGAAAUGGUGGUCAGAGGAUAUAAAAUUUCAGUUAGACAAGAGGAAUAAGUUCAAGAGAUCUACUGUACAACAUGGUGACUAUCAUUAAGAACAAUGUAUUGUAAACCAAAUAUUAUAUGUGGUCACUUAUAAGUGUGACCUAAAUAAUGAGACCACAUGGAUACAUAGGGGGGAACAACAGACACAGGAGCAUACCAGAGAGGGGAGGGUGGGAGAAGGGAGAGAAUCAGGAAAAAUAACUAAUGGAUACUAGGCUUAAUACCCCCAUGACACGAAUUUACCAUUGUAACAAACCUGCACAUAUAUCCCUGAACUUUAAAUAAUAACAAAACCAAAAAAAAAAAAGAAAAUUUCUAAGAGAGUAGAUUUUAAAUGUUCUCACCACAAAAAAGUAUGUGAGUUAAUGCAUAUGUUAAUUAGCUUGAUUUAGCUCUUCCGUAAUGUGUACGUAUUUCAGAACAUCAUCUUGCGCACUAUAAAUGUAUGCAAUGUUUGUCAGUUAAAUAUUUUUAAAUGAAUUUUUUGAAAAGAGGAGGGGUGUGAAAAUGAAGACUACUUCUGACUUUAUAUUUUAUAUUCUGGGGUUACAAGAAUGAGACCUCCCUGAUGCCUACACACAAAUGGAUUAAUGUGAAACUGAAGGUUUACUUGCCCAGUUUACUUGCCCAUGUUUACUUGCCCAGUUGAUUCAGCUGGUUUAUGUAUAAUUGUCAACAAUUUAAACUCUGUCCCAUUCCUCCCCAAAAUUUAUGUACUUUAAAAAUAGAUCUCAUCAUUUCAACAUUUCAAUUUAUAUAUGAGAGAAAUAAAAAGGACUAGUAAAAAUUAUAUGAAGAAGCAACUCCAAAUAUGGUAAUUUAUGGUUCAAAGGAGAUAGGUAAUUGUCUUCUCUCAAGAGCCACUAGACCACAAAAUAUCAACAUCAAAGAUGAAUGCAAGCGCUAGGGGAAACGAUACAGAUCAGAGGCACCAUGUGUUGUGCAUUCUGGUAUUUGUCAGAGAUAAGGAAUGAAGCUGAAUUUUUUCAUGGAUUUGUCUUGAAGGAAAAUAAAAUGAGAGGUUAUGCUAAGUAUAAAACUAUCUUUACAAAGUUCCUUUCCGUUAAGACCUUCAAAGAUAUGUAAAAUCAUAAUUUGAGAAUUGCUUUUAAGGACCUAAUUCAGGUUAGCUAACAAAUCAUUAUCUAAAAAGAGAGUGUUAGAAUACUAUGCAUUUAAAGUGAGUAGUUCACUUCAUGAUUGAGCAGAAAUUCCUGAGUUCAAAUCAUGGCUCUUCCACUUGCAGCUUGUAUGACAUUUAUGAAAUUCCUUAAGUGUGCUCUGUUUCAGGUGCCUCUGCGCCUACAUCAUUAGAGUUAUUCAAGUAUUAAAUGAGAUAAUACAUAUAUAGCCGUUAAACUAGCGCCUGGCAUAGAGUAAACAGUCAGCUCACAUCAGCUAGCGUUAUUCACAAGAAUAGGCUAUACAUUUCUUUCCAUCAAAGAUAAGUGCAAGUUUGAAUAGAAAAAUUAAUUUAUGAAACAAGACUGAUUUUAUGCUUUUCUAUAGUGCCCAUGAUUCAAAGGAAAAGAAGGAAAUAAUCACCAACCAAGUGACCCUGUAAAAUAGAUAGGAGUUACGCCAUGCAUACAUACAUGCAUAUAUAUGUAUUUUGGAUAUAUAUGGAUAUAUUAUGUGUGUGUUUGCAUACGCAUUAUAUAUACAUACAUACCUUUGCCAAGAAAAUUGGAUGUCUCAUAUCUAAAAAACUUUCAGUGUUAAGAACUAGCCAAGUGUCAAGUACACAAUUUGUAUUCAACAUAUAUUUACAGAAUUUAACUUUGUAAAAAUUUCAAAUCACUGUUAUUGCUUUUCCUACUUGUAAAACAAUUACAAAAAUCCCUUGGCUUUUGUGGUGUGGACUAUUAUAAGGGACUCUGAUGCUUCAUGACAGGGAGUAAUUUGAUCCAAAGUACAACGGAGCUCUCGUGUGGAUUUAAGUUACCAAACUAUUGAAGGGACCCAUGCACCACCAAGUAUUCAAAUCACAAUAUAAUUUCAUUAUUCUCUACCCUCCCUUGCAAAUGUAAUAACUCUGAACUGAUAAACACAUUGUACCUGUGUAGAAAAAUGCCACCCAGAAGGAAGCUGACUGCUAAUCUAGGCCUGUGCUGUCCAACAAGAGAGCUAGUAGCCAUAGAGCACUUGAGCUGUGGCUAAUCCAAAUCAGAUGUGCUGGUAAUGUAACAUGCACAAAGGAUUUCAAAUAAUAGUGUGAAAAAAAGUAAAAAUUUUCUCAUUUGUAAUUUUCAUAAUGAUUACAUGUUUAAAUACUAAUACUGUGUAUAGGGUUAAAUAAAACAUAUUUAAAUUAAUUUCACCUGGUUGUAUCUAAGUGUCCAUCAGCCAAUUAACGGAUAAAGAAAAUAUGGUACAUACACACAAUGGAGUACUAUUCAGCCACAAAAAGGAAUGAGAUCCUGUCAUCUGCAACAAUAUGGAUGGAACUGGAGGUCAUUAUAUUAAGUGAAAUAAGCCACACACAGAAAGACAAACUUUGUAUGUUCUCAUUUGUGGGAGGUAAAAAUGAAGACAAUUGAUCUCAUGGAGAUAGAGUGGAAAGAUGGUUAUCAGAACCUAGGAAGGGUAGUGAGUGGCAGGGGUGUGGGAGUGGAGAUGGUUAAUGGGUACAAAAAUAUAUUUAGAUAGAAUGAUUAAGAUCUAGUAUUUGAUAGCACAAAAGACUGAUUGCAGUCACAAUAAUUUAUUGUACAUUUUUUAAUUAAAGAGUAUAAUUGGAUUGUUUGUAACACAAAGGAUAAAUUAUUGAGGUGAUGGAUACCUCAUUUACCCUGAUGUGAUUAUUAGGCAUUGUAUGCCUUAUAUCAAAAUAUCUCAUGUACCCCAUAAAUAUACCUACUAUGUACCCACAAAAGUAAAAAGUAAAUACAUUAAUUUCACCUGGUUGUAAAAAUAACUUUUUGUAAUAUGGCUUUUUAAAAAUUUAAAAUUACAUGUUGUGGCCAUCAUUCAUGGUUCACAUUAUGUUUCUACUGAACAGCGUUGAUCUAGACAGUAGACACUACGCAAAAACAGCUAAGAAAAUUAUUAAUUCUUUAAAAGGAUAAAAUUUAAAGUGAUAAAUGAGAUCAAAUUUUAUGAGCAAGUCCAUCGUAGUUCACUCUGUGCUUGUUUCUAGGGAAAAAAAAUUGGAACUUUCUGUAGAGUGUGCCAGUCAAUGCAAAAGUGCUCAUCAAGAGAGAAUUAAAACAUUAGCAAAUAGGGGCUGUUGAUGAAAAUGAGAUUCCAGAGAGGGUGAGAAGACUGAACACAUUCCUGUAAAGCAACAGGGAUUAAUGCACCAAUGAGAAUUGCUUUUUUUUUUUUAAACAAAACAAAACAAAACAACAAAAAAACCCACUAAAUUUUUCUAGGGGAAAAGUAAAUGCUAGAGUGAUAUUAGUGAAUUAGGGGAUUUGUGAAGAUGCAUUUGAAUGUCAAGAAUAUAAUGUAGUUUUCUUAGUAUUUUUGAAUUCAGUGACCUUUUGUUAACCUCAAGAGACUGAGGCUAAGACACCAACAUUUACCAUGUGCUUCAAUCAUUCUCUCAAGGACGCACAGCUCCUCUGAGCUGUAAUAGGAAUUCAGGUCUGUGUGACUCCUGAGCCCACAUGACCGAACGUGUGCCCAUGGAACACUGGUCCCUGCAACUGCUCUGCAAAUAAUGGUUCUAUACUUAAAUCAUUUUAAGAAAUGUUGCAUGUAUCGUUACCGUCUUAAACAUGAUUCAUUGAUUUGCAUAUUAAAGGCACUGAGAAUUGCUAAAAAACUGUUUAACUUUUUAAAAUCUUUUUCUCAAACUUCUUUUGCCACAGAACACCUCCUCCCCUGCACAUGCAUCUAUAUGCCAUUUAUCACCAGUUGCAUGCUGAAACUAACCUUAGACAGAAUGCUAUUUGGAAAUGCUGAGAUGCCUUAAAUUGCCUUCUAUCAUCUCUCAUUAUUAGUUACUAAGGAAAAUGGCUUUGAGAAAAUAUAAAAUAUUUCAGGAAAAUAUGUAAUUUGAUGCUCAGAUAACUCACUUUUUGCUACAUCAGAAAAAGCAAAACUAGAAUUUAAAAAUAAACUUGGAUGCAUGUCUUGGUUAUUCUUAUAUUCAUAGUGUGUGAUCCAAAGGGAGUCAAAGAAAUCUGUAGCGAGGCUGCUCACAGUCUAGGUCUCUUUUUGUGUAGGACAAAGGUAGGGCUUGGCUUCUAGUUGAAGCUACAGUUCUGUAGGACUUGGGAUUUGGAAAAGUAAUGACAAGAUAAAUAAGUUAUCACCAUCAGAGACCUAAAUGGUUGCAAAUUUGGCACUGGUUACAUAAUGAACAAAAGUUUCAUAACAUAUUUCAUAAGAUAUUUUCAUAACAUAUGUCUUACAAUUACUUUUUUUAUUUUCUGAGGUUUUUUCUCUAAAUUAUGCUAAAAAUGUCAUCGAGAAGCAUAAAAACAGACUUUCAUUAAUAGUUGCUAUAGCAGUGGGAAAUUUUUGUAGGAAUUUAAGUAAAAAAGCAAGUUAUUUAGCAGUUUUGUUCAAAUUAGACAUUUCUGCCAUCAGCCUGCCCCCUGGGAACUUGGAAAGUGCAUACUUGCUCUUGAGUUCUGCUAGUGCCCUAACCACACGCCUUUCAUGUCUACCAUACUUCGAUGAUCUUGGAUUCAAAUAUGAUCCUCUGCCUUCCUCACAGAAAGAAACAAUUUAGGGACAUGGACUUAAUGGUAAUGACUUUCAAAAGCUAAUGACGUGCAGUCUUUCGGCACUGCCUAGCCGAACACUCUUUAGACAACCUGCUGCUUUAGACUGGACAUGCACAUGAUUCCUAAGAUACACUAAACAAGAAUAUGAGAUGCUGAGUCCAUUGUUUCCUGUGCAAAAUUCAGUUCACCAAGAAUACUAUUUUCACCAAGAAAGCCAUAGACUGUGUGUAGGUAAAGAACUUUUGCGCUAAUGAAACUUGUUAUUGGCUGGGACUAGGGGCCUAAAUACUAGUUUGAGAUUCUGUUUCUGCUGUGCCAUAUAGCAUGAGAUCCCACUUUUGCCUCUAUAAAGCAGGGCUAUGGUUAUCUUUCCUUAUUACCUCAGUUGAUUGUUGGCUGUGAGAACCAAGUAAGAUAUGCUUCAUGGAAUAACAGAAGAAUGCAAGAUAUUAUCACGGGAGGCAACAUUUUUGGGAUAUCACAUAUUAGUGGAAACUUAAAGAAUAUUUGAGAGGUUAUCUUUGACAUUUACAUAAAACCAUGUAUGAAACAAGUAGUUCUUGUGUUUUUUUAACCUAUGAACUUUUUCAAGUGUUUUCUCCACAACAUUCCUCUCUUCUACCAAAGAAAAUCAGUUUACAGUCAUGUGUUUUGUAAAAGCCUAAAUGGGAAUGAAGGUGGUUAGUAAGAGGGUUCACAAGAUGGAGAGGCUCCCAUGACAUUUGUAGGUUUAAUCUCGUGCCCCAUGACCUCUUAAAAUGUCCCCAUGCCCAUUCAGAAUACCCCAAUUCACUUCAAAGGCAAAAACAACGUGACAUUGUGAAAUCAUACCAGAUGUUCUAGUAGAACUGUGUUCUGGUCCUAUUGAGUUCACCCAGGAGAGGCAUCAAACUCUGCAAUCAGAACAUAUCAACACAUGGCCUAUUAGCUGAUUCUGCCACUUGGUAGCUGUAUAUUCUCUCUCUGUUUAGUGUCCUUAUCUGUAAAUUGAAAUAAUAAUAAUAGCUCAUAAGGCUUUGUGGGGAUUAAGUGAGAUAAUCAUGUACAGUGCCCAGCACAGUGUCUACUGCAUGGUAAAUACUGCAAAAAUGUUAGCUGUUGACUGCUCCUAUUUAUGACCUUCAUUAUUAAAAAGGGGAACUUAGGCUGACGCAGGAGAAUGGCGUGAACCCCGGGGGACGGAGCCUGCAGUGAGCCGAGAUCACACCACUGCCCUCCAGCCUGGGCGACAGCGAGACUCCGUGUCAAAAAAAAAAAAAAGGUGGGGGGGGGGGAACUUAUGAAUGCCUUUCACUUAUACCAGCAUCAUUAAAAAUUUAAGUUUUUUAAGAACCAUGAAAAGCUAACCAUUGACAAUUUAAGAAGCAUGCAAGCUUGGUUUACAAAAGAACUGGACAAGCUCAGAAUGGGCUAGUUCAGUGGAGUGACUGCUGCAGGAGCUCAGGUUUUGAGACCUUCCUGUCUUCUUCCUUCAUCCUUCUCCUCUUUUUGUGUUCUCUCCACACACUUUUCCUCAUCAAAGCCAAAACCUUUGUUCUUGCUAUAUUCUCUUUUUAGAGCCUGCUCACAGUAAAAUUUUAAAAAAAUGAAGAAGUGCUGAAAGUGUAGAUAAGCAAUUAGACAUGAGUUAAUGUUUUUUAUUUGCAAGAGCAUUUGCAUUCUAAUAUGAACUGAACAUUGAGUAAAUAGAUUCCUGACUCCCUAACAGGGCUAUGUCUUGUGUCAGGAAGCCAGCGCACUGGGCUUCUUGGUAGGCAGGAGACCCAAGUCAUCAUCUGCUACUAAGGCUGGGUCUUGGAAGAUGGAGAAGGCCGUAGAAGAAAGGAAAGCCAAAAAAAGAAAGGAAUGAGAUUUUGAUAUAUUAAUUAGCUCAUACUAUAAGCCUGGACUUUUGCUAGGCAUUUUCCAUGGUAAUUUGGUUAUACCUCAAAACAAUUCUCAACAUUAUUAUCACUGCCACCACUUCUGUUAGCAGCUGUGAGAACAGAGGUCAUGUGAGUAAGCAGUUUGCUAAGGGUUGCAUAGCUUAAAAAGUAGUCAAUAAGCUAAAGUUUGAACCCUGAGAUGCCUGGCCUUCACAGCUAAACUUUUAUUAAUUACACCUGCUUCUAACAACAACAACCAUGGCUAAAGUUUCAUUAACCUACCAGUUUCUAACAACAUUAACAAAAACAUUUUCAAAAAUAUAAUAAUAGUCAUCAAUAGGAAUAAAGGGAAACAAUCCAAAAAUAGCUCUGUUGAGGUUACUGAUGGAUGGGGACAGGAAAGUACAAAAUUUUUUCUACGAAAGUUUCCCUUUGAGGAUCACUUUCCUUGGCUGUCUUGCCUUGUGAAAUUAUACCUUCCCUAAUGGCUUGGAGCUGAUUGUGCCCUUCUUUCUGUCAAGGACAGCUUAAACUUCAUGGAAUAGUUUAUUUGAAGCUUGUGGGUACCAAUUCCAGGCAGCAAGAUACUACUUUCAGAGAUUCAAUUAACUUCCUUCAGAGUCACAGCAAAAAGCGAUAGAGCUAAAUUGAUUACCUUGAAGUGCCUUAACCGUUUUGCUGCUGUUGUUACUUCUUGAGCCAAUUUAUUCUCCCAGCAAUGUCACUGUUACUGAAGUUGGUCUGUUCUUUAUUCUCAGUUUAUGAAUAGGAAUCAUCUGAAUAUAGUUAUAGACCUCUAGUCUAGAUCAUUUUUUGCAAAAUUACAAAGAUGGGAAAAUUUCCAAGCCAUAGUUAUUCCAAAUGGCUGGGAGUGCCUUAGGAACUUAUUUCUGGAGUCUUUUGAACUAUUUAUAUUAUUGAUAUGAACAAUGCCCCUGAUUGUUAGUUAGCAAUCUAUUCAUUGAUAGGGACAUGAAAGGCAGUCUGCUGCCAUCUAGCUUUUUAGUUUCUAUCUUUAGGAAUUUUCCGGUCCUUUCACAGAAAGACACUUUUUAAAGGAGCAAUUCUUACUUCAUCCCUGAGAGGGAGACACUUAUGAAGGUACUGCAGAAUCUUAAAAAAAAAGUCUUCAUCAUUCUUUUACUUCUUUUUGCCUUUAAGUUGGUCUUAAAUGGGUAAAAGUGAUAAAUGUAGGUUGUGUAGUUCAAAUCCAUUGCAGUGACUAAGCAGUGACCACCCAUAGGGGCAAAAACUAUGUAUUUUUAGAGGCAAAGAUUGAUAACCACAGCCAUGACCCUGAGCAAGACUGUGAAAUAGAUGCAGUUCUUUGCCAUCCUCCCUUUUCCUGAGUUAUGGGCACUUUCUGCCUUCAUAGCUGUUUCCUCUGCAAAAUGGAGAUUUUACUGUCAGAAGUCUCCUAUUGCUAUUGCUUCUUGGAGUUGGUUCCCAUGCUCUGGGCACAGGAAAGCAAUCUGAGAUCUUCACUACUAGUAUUUAUUGAGCACCUAUACUAUGCCAGGACUGGACUGUGCUCUGAGGUCACAGUGGUAAACAUACCGACAUGGUUCCUGCUGUCAUGAGCCUUCCAAAGGAAUAGCGAAGAAAAACAUUAAACAUAUCAGCCCAUGAUUAAAUGCAUAAUUAGAUAAAAUGCAUUGAAGAAGUAAAGAUCCCAGGAAAGGAGAGAACCAAUUAAUAUGAUGGAUGGGAAAUCAAGGCUGCUGGAAGGAAGUAGUGUAUAAGCUGAAAAAUGAGGAGUGAAUAGGAAUUAGCCAAGUGAAAAGCAGAGGCAAAUGGGUUUCAGGAAAAGGAAAAACAUAUGUACCAGUAACAUUUCAAGAAGAAAUGGGAAGGAUUAGAUGAUUUCUGUUAUUCUUAUUAGGUUGAUCUCUUCCAUGGAAGAGACACACAGAAUGUAAUUAAUUUAUAGAAUAUAAAAAUGAUUUUUUUUUUUAGGAAUGGGGAGGUGAGGAGAAGACCCGCUUCAAGUUCUGUUCCAAUAUUAAUAUGGUUUUGCUUUCUCUACAAACCUAAGUAAAACAAUGGUGGUACCAAGGGUUGGUUGGGAGGCACUAGUUUUCCCAGUGUACAUACUCACAACUAACAUAAAAGCUAAAUACGUAUAAUCAACAUGCUUACACUACAAACACAACUUCAAAUAAAAUUCACUAGAUCAACCGGGCACAGUGCCUCACACCUGUAAUCCUAGCACUUUGGGAGGCUGAGGCGGGCAGAUCACCUGAGGUCAGGAGUUUGAGACCAGCCUGACCAAGGUGGUGAAACCCCAUCUCUAUAAAAAUACAAAAAUUAGCCAGGCAUAAUGGCAGGUUCCUGUAGUCCCAGCUACUAGGGAGGCUGAGGCAGGAAAAUUGCUUGAACUCAGGAGGCAGAGGUUGCAGUGAGCCAAGAUCAUGCCAUUGCACUCCAGCCUGGGUGACAGAGCUAGGCUCCAUCUCCAAAAAAAAAAAAAAAAAAAAAAAAAAAACUCCACUGGAUCCUCUCUUCCAACUUUUUUCCCCUAAUUUCUUCCCUUAGCACUGAUAUUAUCAAACAAGUGGCCAAUCCUAUAAAGGCUAUCAGACUCCAAUUUAAAAAAACUAUUAAAUUUAAAAACACUCAGAGAUAUAAUGAUUGUAUGCCUUUUAUGAGGAAACUUAGUACCUAAAAGAAAACCCUAUAACUUAACAUUAAGCAUAUGAAGGUAGCUAUUAUUCAAAUAAGUAGCAGUAAAGACUUUUCAGCUUUGGAUCCUCAUAAACAAGACCUGCAGGUUUAAAGAUUUGCAUACAUCUUUUAACAAUGCAUCAUUUUUAUUAUAGUAUAUUAUAUACUAUUUUAUAUUUACUUAAUGAGAUUACUGACCUGGGUUUCAAGAUAUGUAUGAAAUAUAAUUAGGAUAUGAAAAUUAAAGAUAAAUUAUCCCCACCAGAAAUAAUCUUAGCAGGUUAUUUACUAAAGAAUCUUAAAUCCAGCAGAUCAAGAAAAACUCCCCAAGGAGUCUUUAAUUAGAACUCUUUAGGAUGGAAUCAAAAUCUCUCCAUAAAAAAUGAAUCUUGCCUUAGGCUACAUAAAUUACAAAAUCUGAAGCCCUUUAAGCAGCAUUAAAACUGCUGAUUUUAAUUGCUCUGAUAAUGAACUGGAGAGAGACACACUAAGCUUCCUGGAUUUCUGUUGGAAAUGAAUGGGAUUCUUGCCAACUAUGGAUCACAGUUAUGAGGUAUUCUGCACAGGGAAAAUCAAAAGAAAGCAGAUGGACCUUGACAUGCUAUGCCAUCCUAUGCCUUCUUCCUUCCCAAGAAGCAUGUUACAAUAACUUUAAGUGAAGGUUGUCACAACUUUAAGUGAAAAGUCUCCCCUUUCUGUCUAAUUUUUAAUGUAACUUCCCCCUUCUCGAUAUAUCCAGAAAAUAGUUAAUAACAAUCCCUGAGGGAAAAGAAAAAUGCUGCCCUUCAUAUUAAAAAAAAGAAGAUAACAGAGAUCCCCUUAGUGGUGAGUGAUUUAUAGUGAAAACAGCCAACUCAUUCUCUUUUGCCUCCUUUUGACCUAGAGAACUGGAUUCGCGGAUUUGUAACUGGAUUUUGAUUAUAGAGUAUGUUCUAUGGCUACAAAAGAGUUUUCCUUUGAGGAAAACUCAAACUGCCAACAGAUAUGCUUGGUAUAUCAGUUUUCAAUGCUUUCAAUUGUAAAUAACAGAAACCUGGACUCACAAUAGCUUGAACAAAUAGGAAUUACUUUUAAGUAGGUGGCACCGGAGGUGUUUCAGCUGUUGCAUGAUGUUAUCACCAUUUGCAAAGAGGCAGCAUCUCCACAAUUUUCUUGGCCUGUUCCUCUUGAUGGCAAAUGGCUACUGCACGUCCAGAUGAUCAUGUCUGUGUCACAGAUAGUGAGAGGGAAGGAGGAAGGAUGAGAGAGGAUGGCCAGCUAAAGUUGUAUCUACCCCACUUAUAAGAAACACAAAGCCCUUCCCCAGAGCUUACAGCCCUUUAGCCAGAACUAUGACACAUGGUCAUCUUGAGUGCAGAAAGAUGGAAGUUAACAUUUGGUUUUCUGGUCUUUUUAAUAAAGAUAGCAAGGAUGAAGAAGUUUGGAAAAGACUGUGGGCUAGCCAAUCAAAUUGUCGACCACAUUUGGCCUGUAUUAAUGUAUAGUUUUUAAAGCCUAAUGUCAAUUUGUUAAGGUGUCUUAAGGACAGGAAAAUGGAGAAGAACUAAGAUUUUUUAUAUCAAAUACAGAGUAAAUCUUGGAAAGGGUGAAUUAGAGUGGAAAAUAAACUAGACAUUAUCUAAGAGUGCCUUGAAGCCAGAUCUUGCAAAACAUUAGGCAAGCAUGUCACUCAUAAUGGACCCCAGGGCUUUCCAUCUCAUAAUGUGGAUAAAAAUAACAGUGUUUCUCUCAGUUUUUAAAAAUGUCACCAAAAAUUCAAUAAAGUAUAUACAUACAUAUUGUAAUUGUUUAAAGUAAAAAUUUUAUGCUGUUUUGGGAAGAAAAAUAACCAAAAAAAACCAUCACUGACCAUUGGUCAUCAAAAUCUGAUUUAUGCCAUGUUUACAAGAUAAAAACAAGAAUAAAUAAUAAUUGUUUGAAAUAUUUUCAUCAUAUUGCCUCUGAAAUGAUUGAUGUCAUACUGCCUGGAUUUAGUCAACUCAGUGAAUGAUUUAUCAGUAGCCAUGCUCUAAGGAGCUCUCUAUUCAUAGAUACUUAUGAUUUGGUGAACUGGGAAACCCACAGAGAAAGGUAAAUGAAAUAGGAGAGCCAGGUAAAUGGGCCAUGGAUCUAAGAACCAGGAAUCAUGAUUGUUUGGAAGAACAUAUCUCAGACUGAGAAAAGCUGGCGCUAAAGUAAGCUAGCAUUUGAUUAGAAUGUUGAAGGAUAAUUUCAUUCUUGGAGACAGAAAACCUAAGUAGAAGCAAAAGAAGUAGGAAAUAGAAGCCUGUGUUUGAGAGAUUCAGAGUGACUGUGUUUUAUUAGAAUUGCAAGAAAGGGAACUUGAAAACAUAAAUUUAACAUGGGGCAACAGGCCUUGGAUUCUGAACAGAGGGACUUUGUUUAAGGAUGGCUCUGUGGCUGUGGAACAGUUUUUCUAUAGAUUAUCAAAAUGAUUCUGGAAAAGAAAUGUCAUUCUGGACUGAGAGCACAUACCAUAGGGAAAACAUGAGGCUUAUGGGCUGAAUUGUGUCACACCCAAAGUCAUAUGCUGAAGUCCUAACCUAGGACCUCAGAAUGUGGCUUUAUUUGAAGAUUGAGCCUGUAAAUAGGUGAUUUUGAUAAAAUGAGAUCAUUAGGGUAGACCCGAAUCCAACAAGGCUGGUGUCUUUAUAAGAAAAGGAGAUUAAGAUGCACGCGCACACGCAGAGAAGACUACGUGGAGAUGAGGAGAAGAUGGCCAUCUACAAGCCAAGAGGAGAGGUCUCCCGAAGAAACCAACCCCACUGACAUCUUGACCUCAGUCCUCUGGCCUCCGGAACUGUUUUAAAACAUAAGUUUCUAUUGUUAAAGCCACCUAAGUCUGUGGUAUUUUGUAAUGGCAGCCCUAGGGAAAAACUACAAUGAGCAAGUAUUAUUUGUAUUUUAAGAAAUAAUAUUAUAAACUAAAUUCAUGGAGGGGAAAAUAGAAAAAGAGGUCAUUUCUGAAAACAUUGUAUAGGUGUAACAUAGUUGACACUAUCAACUACUACAAUGGGAUCAGGAGACAGAGGGUCAGUGAUAACGGAGCUCUCAAGACUGGAAACUGGGCGAUCCAGAAGGACAGGCGGUUGAUGAAAGAAAAUGAUGAGUGUGGUUGAGGCUGCGUUUCCCUUGAGGAGGUGCUGGUGCUCAGGGUAGAGGCAUCCAUCACGAUGUCAGAAAUGUGUGUCAGACACGAAGGCAGGAAUGAGGCUGUCGAGGAAGCCAUGGCAACAUAAACAGAGAAGUGCCACAGCGAGACAACCAGCCAAUGAGUUGUGUAGUUUCUUGUAAGUAGCUGAAACAACAUAACCAAAUUGUUCAAUUUAGUCUACAUAUGAAAUUUCAAUGUCAGAGAAAGGCCUUUAAUCUCAAAACGAAAUAAACUAAAAGACAUUAUUUUCCUGACAGCUAAGUCUUAAAAUUUCUUUUGAGAAAUAAAAAAAAUGGUUUUCUCUUUUAACAUAGAGGCAAACCAGUAAGUCAGAUACUUCAGGGGAAGGUAGCUUGGUGAUUUGAAUGUAUGUGAGUGUGAAUACGUGAGAUUAGAAUCUUACCUGAGAACAAAUUUUCAUGAGCAUCAUUGGAGAGUGGGAGAGCAUGAAGACUUUUACCCUUCUCUCUGCAGGAGAGAAUUGUGCAGGAGGAGGUGGGGAGAAUGCCACCAAGAACAGGUUGCCUGGGGCUAGUUUAGCGAUGGGGUCCAAACGAUCUCACUAAUGUGAAAGGAUCAUAGUUACCUUACCAAGGGAAAGUUGGCUUCAACUAUAUAUUUCACUUCUGUACCAGGUUUUGCUUAAAUGCUACUCUUUGGAGAAUAUCAAGAAAUUUAGAUGAGUUUACCAAAUCCAAGAUUGUGUUCCCUGCUUUUAACUCUUGUUACUGAAAUAGCCCCCUGAUCCCCAAGAGUAAUGCUUGACUGAGGUGUUUGCAUGAAUUGUUUAUAUCAUUCAUUAAUUAACGUGAUGAACAUAUUAAAGAUAGGACUCCCAGUUUUCAUCCCAAGGGCUUACAUAUAAUAGUAACAACCUUUAGAAAAGUACUGCAUUGUUUAUUUAUAGAAUGGCUUUGACUCACUUAAUAAUGCUCCAUAAUUAAUUUGUAAAUUACUUUUUGACUUUGCACAAUUAUAAUUUAAUGUCAUAUAUCUGCAAAAGAAAACACUUUUAUGUUGCUAAUAUUAAUUUCCCUUCAUAAAUUUGAGACUGUUUUGACUAUAGAUAAAUGUAAAAUGUCAAUGUGGUGAGAAUGACUCAGCUUCUCAGAUAUUCAUUUAUUCUAUAAAUAUUUUUGAAUACCUACUAUGUUUCAGGCACUGAUCUAAGUGUUGAAUAAGUAGACAAGGACAGCCUGCCUUCAGGUUUUUUACAUUCAAAUAACACAAGAUGAUGAAGAAAUUUUUAAAAUAAUCUGGUUCCAUUUGGCAGAUAAUAUAGAUAUGCUCAGUUUUAUAAAUUUUGAUACCUAAAGUAUUGUGAUAAUCCAAAUCAUGACCUUUAGACAUUACACUAUGCUUAUUGAUUGAAGGUUGACAUAUGUUUAGCAUAUUCUCUUAUAAUGUAUUUAAGGACUUCAGUGAGUAGACAAAAGAAGUAAACUUGAUCAGACAACAUGAUUUCUGAGAACAGACUCUUCCUGGAGCAAGCAUUCUGGUUAGAUUUUACAGGGCUUCAAUAAAAAGGUAUAUGUUUAUGCUUUUUGCUAGUUGGGGGUUUCCUAGCAAAUGAUUCCAUGAAAACAUUUGCAGGGAAUUCCCAUCUGUUCUAUAUUUCCCUGAUUUGGGGGCUCUGAAUCAAUAAUGCUGAUGUAACAGUUGGCAAAUUAGAUAAGAACAGCCCGAGACUUCCUUUUCCAUUAGGUGUAGUCUCAUGGAAAAUCACCCUUGAAUCCAUCAAUGGAAUGAAGCAACUGGGUGGAGCCUAUGGGAAAAUCCUGGAGGAAGUCCCCAACUAGUCAGCCUCCCCUCUCUGCCUUGCACUCUUGGAUUCCUUAGCGAAACAUCCAAAAUGGCCUUCUUGCAAGGAGGAUGCAGUCGGUGAUCCACAUACUGACCAACAGCUGUGUGUGAAAGGCACCGUGCCCACCACAACAAAGGGGCAGUGAGGUCUGCUGAGCAGAUGAGUCGCUUUUCUGGACCCUUCCAGGCUUGCAGUUGGCUCAGAUGAAAAGCUCAGGCUUAUGAGCUGCCAGAAAGUAUUUGGCAAAAAGCCCACCUUUUUUCUCAAGUACACGUAUUCAAUUGACUUGAUUCCUCAGAGAGAUUUGUGAGGGUGAAAGCAAGUUCAUUGUCCACUUUUAAUGACCCUCAACUUCUAAUGAGGUAAUAUAUGUGAAAGUGAUUUUUUUAAAUGCAAUGCAAAUACAGGGUGUUUUUAGUCAUUAUUUCAGUACCUGAGGAAAAUGUAAAAACACAAAGCCACACAUGUACCAAGGCACUACAUGAGUGUACUUGGUUUCACCAUCUAAUUUAGCCCUCUGAAGUGUAGAGUCCAUCGAGGCUAUUAUUUUGUGGAUUGUGUACUGAAGUUGCUUUUCUUUGUUCUCCCAACAUACACUUGUGACACUUCCAACCUCUGAUAUGUAUAUGUUAAAUACAGGCUGUUUUUCAAACAAGAUAAAUCAAAUGCUAGCUAGGAAGUGUGCCUAGAGUUUAAAGCAUUCUAGAAUGUACUCCCAUAUAACAGCUAUACUUAUAUAAUACCUACAUUGUGCCAGUGUUUCAUAUAUGUGAAGUGCUUUAAUCCUCACAACAAACAUAGGAGGGAUGUAGUAUUAUUACCCCCUUUUUACAGAUGUGAAAACUGCAGUACACAAGGUGAAGUGAGAGGCCCCAAAUCACACAGCUAGUAAAUGGCAGUGUCAGACCUCAAAUUCCACUAGUCUGUCUUCAGAGUCUAUAUAAUUAACCACUGCUCCCUGUGCUUUUAAAGGUUAGUUUAAUGGAUAUUGUGCUAUUUCUAAUAAAAGGAUAUAAUUUUUGUUAUAUAUUUUUCUUCUUAGUCUUCACUUUUGGAUCUUGGACCACAUGUGCUAUUAUCAUAUUUUAGCUCAUAAGAGACUUCUCUGAUAAUUUUGUAUAAAAUACACUUAUAGAACAUUUGUAUCUUGUAAAUGUAAUUUUUCUUACCAUUAUCUCAUUUGAUCCCCCUUAUCCACCUCUAGAAUAUACAGAGCUUUAUCCUCAUUUUUCAGACGAAGAAAUGGACCAAAGAAGACUAAACAAUUUGUUCAACUCCAUAUCACCAGUUUGUAGCAGUUCUGUGACUAGAAACCAAAUUUCCUGGCUCUUAGUCCUACAUUCUUUCUAGUAUUUCAAAUCAUCUUUUCAUUUCUCUCCCUUAUGCUUUUGGAAAGAAAAUUGAGAAGAACGUUAAGAACCCCAGUAAAAUUGGAGAGGCAUUUCUUGAGAAAUAUUUAAAAUAAUUUAAGAAGUCUUCACAAAAGUAGUAGGCAAAAAUGUGUUACAUUAACAACGGAUCUCAUUAAGUCAGUGCAUACAGCUAGGUUCUGGUUUAUUAAUUUUCAAUUUUUUCAUUUUUGGGCCUGCCUAAUCUGAACACUUUGCAGUACAAUUCUGAGUGCUCUCAUGCUUUGUGCUAUCGCUUUCUUAAGGUAGCUCAUUUGCACUUGUUCAUCAUCCUGUUCCUUCCCCCAGUCUCCUGGGCUCUGUUGCUAAUUAUUGACCCAGGAAAGCCUCAGAAGGGGCCAAGGCAGCUAAAAUUGGAGUGCUCUUUACUUAGACUUAUAAUGCAUUUUCCAUUUUUCAGAAAGAGUAAAGCACUUUUAGCUACCAGAUCCAGAGACCAUUCAGUUAUAUGGGCACUUGAGUUUCUGCUAAAGAAUCACAACUCAAUUUAAUUUUUUUUUUUUUUGGUAUUUCAUUCACAGCCAGUCUGGAGUGUGUGUGUGUGUGUGUGUGUGUGUGUGUGUGUGUGUAUUUCUGUUUCUGUAUUAACAUAUGAGACAGCAGAAUAAUAAUGUGUCCAUUCAUUCCAUAGAUAUUUCUCAAAGAGUUGCCAAGAAUAAAGAAUAGUGCUAAAAAAAGGUGGAAGAUGGUUAGGUGUAAAAUUACCUCCUCUCACAGGACCUGGCACAUGACAAAUGCUUCAGAAAUAUUUAUCAAACUGAAAUGAGCUAUUACAUGAAUUGUAUUCUCUGGCUUUGGAAUCUAUUGGGGAAAUGAUGAAGUCAUUAAAUAUAUGCGAAUUGGAAAGGAAUUUAGGAAUCAUCUUAUGCAGCCCUUUUACUUUAAAGAUGAAGCAAUGGAAAUGCAAGAAAGUUAUGUGUCUUUUCCAAGCAAGAUCACACAUCUAUUUCGAAAUAAUAUGCUUUUUUUCAUUGUAACAUGUGUUUUAGAGAUUACACAUAUGUCAAUGUCUGUAGUGCAGGGCAUAAUGUGAGGAGAGCUGUUGAAUGCUUUAGAACAGUGCUACCCAGUGGAAAUAUAAUGCACACCCCAUAUACAAUUUUAGAUUUUUAUUAAUAGCCAGAUUUUUAAAAGUUUAAAAGUCAGUGAAAUUAUUUUUUUCAUACUAAGUCUUCAAAAUCCAGAGUGUGUAUUAUAUUUUUGACACAUCUCAAUUUGGACUAGCCAUAUUUUAAGUAUUUAAUAGUUAUAUGUGUCUUGGGGGGGGCUACUCUAUAGACUAUAUGGCUCCAGAAUCACAGAGAGGGAAAAAUAAUAAUGUAUUUUUAAAGCUGCAGUAUUUUUACCAUGGGUUAUAUUUUUAAGUUUGAUUGUAACACAAAAGUACAAAAAUGAAACAAACUGACUCAACACAUUUUUUUUCUUUUUUUUAUUAUUAUACUUUAAGUUUUAGGGUACAUGUGCACAACGUGCAGGUUUGUUACAUAUGUAUACAUGUGCCAUAUUGGUGUGCUGCACCCAUUAACUCGUCAUCUAGCAUUAGGUAUAUCUCCUAAUGCUAUCCCUUCCCCCUCCUCCCACCCCACAACAGUCCCCGGUGUGUGAUGUUCCCCUUCCUGUGUCCAUGUGUUCUCAUUGUUCAAUUCCCACCUAUGAGUGAGAACAUGCGGUGUUUGGUUUUCUGUCCUUGCGAUAGUUUGCUGAGAAUGAUAGUUUCCAGCUUCAUCCAUGUCCCUACAAAGGACAUGAACUCAUCAUUUUUUAUGGCUGCAUAGCAUUCCAUGGUGUAUAUGUGCCACAUUUUCUUAAUCUAGUUUAUCAUUGUGACUCAACACAUUUAAAAAAAAAAUCUAGAGUAGACCUAUACAAUUUGACAGAUUGCAUCAAUAGUUACAAUUUUAGACACCCCUACCCCUCCACACAUAGAAAUUAGUGAAUAAGCAGACUGUCAAUAGUACUGGCUCAAAUAAUUCUACAUACAAGUUCUACCAAACUUUCAAGGGAGGGGUAACUUCUACCUUAUACGAAUUAUCUCAUUUUACAAGUAACUAUAAGUAUACAAUAAGUUCCAUUUGCAGCACUAUAGGAGCUUGAACUGUCUGCCAAUUUUUAAAGAAUAUGCUCAAGCAAUAAUCUUGGUUAUCCAUAUUAUCUUACAUUUCCUUAUGAAUAUUGAGAGUUCUGUUAUUGAUAAAUACAAAGGUGUCACUGUUUAAUACACUACUGUGUAGGUCCUUUUGCUAUGCAUUUACUAUUUAAAGCGUAAAAACGUAGGUAGCAAGAAGAUUUAUCUUUCUGGCUAUUCUUGAAAUUCCUGUUUCUAACAAGAUAUUCUGCAGAAGCAAAGAUACUACUGCAUUGUUCAAUGUUUCCACAAAAGGUUAAUAUAAUUGUGGGUUCAGCUAUCACCUUGACCUUUUCUUGGAUCUUUGAUCAGAGUUUAGGUAAAUAUGUUGUUAGGUUUCCCCCUUUUAAGUUCCUGAGCUUUUGAAGUAAAACCAGAGCUGAGAUAGGAAAGUGAACAGCAAGGGGCAGAGCACAGCAGAAACUGAAUUAGGUCACUUUUCUAGAGGCUUCUGAAUUUGGUACAGUAGGAUUUCUGUGAUCAUCUUAAACCUAGCUUUUCAAAAGGCUAUUACUGUUCCAUUUUAUUCUCUGGCCCAGAAAAUAAAUCAGAAGACUUCUACAUCCUUUUCCUCAAAAGCUGAUUCUGAUUCUCUAUAUGAUGCCACAUUAAUAAAGUUUUCCCUAUUAAUUACCAUGAUGCCAUGCAGCCUUCUAAGAUGUUUUCUUUAGUUCUUAGUUCCUUUGCAGUUCCAUCUCCAAGCAUAAAUUCUCAUUAAUAAUCAGUACAGUGAGGAAGAUAGACAUGUGUCAGUCAGUGAGAAUGCUUGCAGCUGUAACUGCCAGAAAGUUGUAACUUAACUGGCUUAAACCAAAGCCAUCCUGAGGUGGGAGGCUCCAAGUCACUCAGUGACAUUAUCAAAGGCGGCCUGAGUCUUUUUCAUCUUUCUCUUCUGCCAGCCUCAAGUGUUGGUGAGUUUUCUGGUUUGUUCCUGUAAACUCGAGAUGUCUGUCACAGGUCCACCUAUUACAUGCAGAUAACUAUGGCCAGUCAGAAAAGAGGAUCUUCUUUUUACGUCUUCUUUUAAGAAAGAAAAAAAAUCAUUUCCAGAUGGUCUCCCCUUGUCCCACUUCCCUUCAAUGUCUUAUUGGCCAAAAUGGUUUCACAUGCCGAUGUCUUAACAAAUCACUGCCUUGGAAAUCGUACUUUCAUGAUUAGCUGAGACAAUCAGGUUUCCCUCAUGGUGGCUGGGGCUGAGGCCCACCUCCCUGUAAGUAUGUGGCUGCAAGGGUAGGUGGAUAUUUGAAUUUCACUGGGGGCCUAGUAGGAAGGAAUGGCUCUUGGGUAGGCUACCCAUAGAGUCAACUACAAGUAAAUCAGAAACUAUAGUAUCAUAAGUGCUACAGGGAAACAUGUAAAUGCAGGAUGCUGUAGGAACACGCAAGAAGGGCCCCUGGCCAUGCUUGCUUGAGCAAGAGGGAGAGAGGAAUGCCAGAGUGGGCUUUUAAUGAAAAUGUUAUCUGAUCUGAGAUAUAAAGCUCAAGAGGAGAUAGCCAAGGAAAGGGUGGUGGAAGGAGAGAGAGGGUAUCAGGUAGACACAGUAUCAUGUGCAAAUGACUGGGAAUAAGAUAAAAUGUGGUAGGUUUGGGGAGAUGCAGAAAAAUUAGUUGGCCUAAGGUAUAGAGCAUAAGUUGGGGAGUCAGUCAGAAAUAGGGCUAUAGAGGUAAACUGUAGAUCAUAAAAGAUCUGAUAAGUCACAUAGAAAUUUCUACUUUAUUCUGCUGCAGUGGGGAGCCAGUGAAAUAUUUUAAGCAGCAAAUGACAUAAUUAAAUAUGCACUUCAAAAAAAAAAUGUCUUUGGCUGCUGUGGGAAAUUGGAUUGCAAAUCUUCAAGACCAAAAGUAGGUAGAACAUGUGAGAAUCAAUUACAAUAUUCCAGGAAAGAGUGGUGAAGGGCUUUAAGAUAAUGUCAGUGGGGCUGGAGAGAGGUGAAUAGGUUUGAUUGAUGUUUAGGGGUUUUGACUAAACAGGACUUGGUUAAUAGGUAAGAGAAAUAGGGAUUAAUAAUCACUCACAUUUCUGGCUUGGACAACUAGGAGGAUGGGAAUGACAUUUACUGAGUUAGGAUAUCCAAAGAAGAAGCAGACUGGGGGCAAGGGGAGUGAAUUAAUUUAAAUUGUAACUAAUGAAGGGCUUAUUCUGUAUGAAAUUCAAGAGAAGUAUUCCAGUCCUUAAAGCAUUUUCAAAUGCCAAGGGAUAUAUUAACCAAUAAGUGGUAUAGAACAAUACUAGGGGUACUAUAAUUUAUCACAGAUGGUCAUCAAUAAAGCAAGAGAGAGAGAUAAAAGAGCUUAAAGAAGAAAUUGCCUCUCUCUCAGAAAGAAUUAGUGGGAGAAUCUGAUGUUCUUCAUGAAAGAAAAAAAUUUUAGUUGAAUCUUGCAUAAAAAGAUUAGACAGAUGGGAAUUGUCGAGGGUGGAGGCACUGUACACUACAUGAAGCAUAUUUAAGGAAUGAUAACAGUCUAGAUUGCUAGCAAGCUUGAAUAGGCAAAAUAAAAUAGAAAGGUUAGGGAUUAGUUGAAUUAGUCAGAACUGUUGAGAUUCCAAGAGAAAAACAAAAUUCACAUUUUCUGUGUUGAUCUAUUAUUGCAAGGUGCAUUAGUCAGCUAUUGCUACAGUAAUGCUACCGAACAAUCAACUACAAAAUACCAAUGACAUUUGCUUCUUGCUCAUAGUCCUACUAAUGGGUCAGAAUAGUGCUGCUUCAGGCUGCAGGUUGCCUUCAUGCUUGUUCUUCAUGUUUCUCCUUCUUGGACCAGUGAUCUCCCAGGGCGUGUCCUUGUGGCACAGUUUACAACUCCCAAUGUGGCAAGUAGAAAUGUUCAAUACUUUGUAAGGCCUCAGUUUAUAAAGCAGUAUCAUUUGUGCCCACAUUCUGUUAGCCACAGCACAUAAUGUGACUAAACCCAAUAUCACUGAGGGAGGAGAGCAUGAGGAAGAAAAGGAUGGUGAAUAUAUGCUGCAAUGCCUAAAACAUAAUGUAAAUAUAGAUAGCAUUGGAUUUGACCCAUAAGCCAUAAAGAUUCUAGAAUACCAGUGUUCCCAACUAUGGAGUGCCCAAUGAGCUUCUUGACAAACUCAGGAGAGUAACCUCCAUUUGUGUGACCUCCUUUCUUUGCUCUUUAUUUGUGCUUUUCAAAGGGAUGACAUGAGCCCAUAAACUACUCAUUGGGUUGCUUGGUCAGAAUCAGAACCAGUUACUUCAGGACUGUCUCAUUUCAUGAUUAGUUGCCUUUGGUCUCAUGCAGUGGUAUCAGUUCAUUCCUCUAGAGGUUUAUGUUCCCUCAAUCACCAGCAAUACUGAGUGAAUGAUAAGAACUAAAGCAAUAAAAAAUGAUUGAACUAUUUUCCUUAGUAUGUAGUUAUUGGACUUCUUCCAAAAAUCCAGCACACUUAUAAAAACCAAACUAAGGCAUUUUGCUGGUUAUUGUGCCAAUAGUGUGUCUUAAUUAGUCCUGAGAAUUUAUGUGGCCCAUGAAAGAGGCAUAAUUUUCCUAAGAUUGCACAGCUAAGUUACAUAUCUGAGACUUGAAGACAUCCUCAGAUUAUGUUAUCCCUAAAUCUCUAAUUGCUAUGUAGCAAAAGAUUUUAGCCAUUUUUUUAUUCCUGAAUCAAGGAUACAUAAAUAAAGUUGUAUUCAAUCAAUCCAAAAAUCCUCAAGCCCAAAUAAUCCUAGUACUUGAGCAGACCUUAUAGUGUGUGUGCACAAGUGCGCAUGCGUGUACUCUAUUUUUAGAUUAUCUUUUAAGAGGGACCGGUGACAUGGUCAUACAGUACAACAGAAGAACUCACUCCCUGUUUCUCUAUAAUUCCCAUAUUACACUCAGCACUUGCUCUCCUUUCAUUCUGUGGCUUCUGUGCUGCUAGCAGUGACCAGUGACUCAGGAAGGCUGCAUAUAGUGAAGAAAAAGUUGCCUUUCCAGGCACAGUUCAGUCCUGAGGCGCCUUUUCACACCAUCUCAUAGACAUUUCAGAGCCAAACUCUAGCUUUCUUUUUAUGACUACUUUUCCAUUCCACACUUUUCUUAAUGUUGCAGGAGAUAAUUUGAAAGAAAGGAAAAAAGAACAGGGAGAACACAAAGGCAAGAAGAUGAGCAAGAUGCCAGAUUUAAGAAGUAUAUUUAUAUUUAGUUCUUUACAAAUUAAAUUCUGCUGAGACCCUUAAAUAUUAGCUGUCACAGGGGUUGUGCUUGAAAAACUUGAUUCCAACCCUAAGCAUAAAAAUCUUGUCUAGGCAGGGCAGUAGAUUGGAGGAUUAUCAUUACACAUUAUAGGAGGAAGGCCCUGUUCAAUGCCAGGUUCCAAGAAUGCCAUCUCAGGGAGCGAGGGAAAGACAUAGGCCAGGUAACAUGUCUGAUGUAUGGAGAAAAGCCCUCAGGGUGCCAUGUUGGUGGAACAGGAGCAGAAAGGAAAUCAGACUGAGAGAAUGAAAACUCAAUAGAAGCACAAUAAACAGACUGAACAAAGUACAGAUGGAGUCAGUUCAAGUUUAAUAUGAAUGUCCCUGGGCCCUGUGUUUCAUCCCAGUGUUAAGUGCAGGAAAUCAUUGGAUUUCUCCAAGGAUGGGUCUUUAGAGCAACCGACUUUAGAAAUUGAAUACUUUAAAAUUAUUUUCUAUAAACAAAUUUAUCAAUAGAAAAAAUAGAUUACUUAAUUGGUUUAUCUUAAUGAGAAAACAACAAAAAGCUUCAACAAAUAAUUGUUGCUGAUUGGUUGGUGGGUUCGUUGGUGAAUAAUGAGAAGGAAAGAAGGAAGAAAAGAAAAGAAGGAGUAGAGGAGGAAAGGAGGUGAGAGAGGGAGAUUUGAAAGGGAAAUAGCGGUGCUCUAAGUUCACAAUUUUUAAAAGCCUAGAGUUAUUAACAAAUUAUGCCCUCAAUCAGAUUUUAUAUAACUUUUUUCAAUCUUGUCAUAUAUUAAUGUGCUGUAUUCAUGAAAUGAUUUUGAGAUUUUAAAGCAAUGAUUGACAAUAUAGUAGUUCAUUUAAAGUUUUUACAAGUUGCUGCUGACAAAAUAUGGGUAAUGAAUUACAUCAAAUAAGUAUAAAUAUAAGUACACGCUUUGAAGUUAAAACUCAGUAAGUUGUUAUGAUUAAAAUUGUUCACUUUAUUUUCCUCCUGUGUAUGGGUUUCUCAUAAAUGGUAACUUAUACCUAUGAAAAUACAGGGUUCUAUAAAGUCUGAAAACAUAGUUAUUAUAUAUCUUAACGGACCGAAGAUGUCCUUCCUGAUAUUAUGUAUAGCCUGUGUUUCCAGACUAAGUGCCAGGCACUAUUCUAAGUUAGGCACGAUUCUAAGUGUUUUACUGUUCAUUUAGGCUGUCUGGCUAGUGUUUUUCUCACCUUAUCAGCAUCCCAUUUUUAUUAAGUGAAUUUGCCUAAACACACCUGCACACGCACAUGCAUGCGCGUGCACACACACACACUUUUUGCAUUUGGAAGCCUGGCUAUUAUGGAACUCUAGAACAUGAGAGCUCAGGGUCAACCACCAAGACUCAAUAAGGUAUGGCUGGGGAUGUGACCAAGACUAUCCUAGCAUCUAUGGCUGUGGACUGGGUGUCUUCUCCACUGACCCUUGAAGGUAGUUUUGCUUCACUGCUUUAGAAAUGGUGCAGAGACUUAAUCUUAUUUCACUUUUCGGUGUUUGUCUUGGUUCCUGUAGAACUGGCUUGAGGCUUAGAAGAUGUCCUCCCACCUGCAUUUGGAAAAAUACAUUUCUAACACUUCUCCUCAUAUGGAAAUUUUUAAGUCAUUGAAAAACUCAUACUGCAGCAUUUGUAGAAACAAUUUCAGAACAGAGUACCUUAUUGCUUUUCCUAAAAGAAUUUUAACUGUGCAUGUAUAAGUAUUAUAAAUGCAUAAAAUAUAUAGUUAAUCCAAAAGACAUAACUAUAUCAUGCAUAGUAGUUAUAGGUCACCUCAGAUAUAUUAGUAACAUCUUUUUAUAGAGACUCUGUUGUUAUUUCACUCACACAAAAGAAUAAACACAGAAUUAAGGUUGAAAUUUACAUAAGACCAGUCUAAAGCCAGCCAUAGCUAUGUAAUUUCCAUGAUUUUCUCCCAAUCAAUGGAAAAUUACUGUCAGCUGAGCCAAAGUCUGCAGACUGUGAGCAAAUGUCUGUUUCCUUCCCACAACUGAGUGUUUGAAACUUUUUUCAAUCAGUAAAAUUACCAUUAAAGGUCAGAGAUUAGUUUUUCAUGCAUGAUGGAUUCCAUUUGCUUUAAAAGUAUUAUACCAGGAGAGUAGACUUUUUUUCUGACUUUAGAAUCAAAUUAGAAUUCAAAUAUUCAGAGUUUUGGGUCAACCUCAAACUAUUUUAUUUUGUUUAUUUUCCCUUGACAAAAUGUUAUUGUUUUAAAUAGGGAAGGAGAAAGGUCUUGGGAAAACACACACACACACACACACACACACACACACACAUAUAUAUGUACUCUCUCAUAUUUGAAAUUAGCAUGUAGUUUAAGGAUACUGCACACAGCUCUAUGAUGAGCUUAACUUGAAUCUCCUUAGAUUAUGAGCAUUUUGAAAGCAGGGACUUGAUUUUUUAACUAAAUACCUUUCAUGUUUGAUAACCUGUUCCUUUUCCUGUGUGUAUUGUCUUAACUAAAGACUGCCUGCAAUGAACAGAAGGGCUAUGGUCUUUUUUUUAUUAAGAUAAAAGAAUUUUCCAAAUCGUUGUUUAUAAAAUAAAAGAUUAGAAAAAUUCACCUGUGUAUAAAUUGAACUAGACUUCUAUAACAUAGCAGCCAUCUUGUGCAGAAAGGGGCUGCUUACGUAGUUUAUUUCUUUAACACACAGUUGCUAAUUACAAAAACAGCAUGCAUCCAGAGAUUGUGAAAAAAGAAGUUAAAAAAAAUCUUGCCUAUUAUUCUACCACCGUAACACAAUUAUGUUUAACAUUUUUCAUAUUUUUAAUUUAUUUUCUCUUUCCAUAAAUUCUAAUCUGUCUAUAAAUGUACUAUUGUGGUCUGCUUCGUUGACUAACAGAAUAUUUUCACCCCUUUCAGAACCCUUUUUUUAAAAAAUGGCUUCUUUUGUGUAUUUGAAACAAUUUCAACUUAACCCUAUUGCAUAUAUUCUGUAAGUAGCUGUCCUUCAUGAAACAGACAACUUUUUCUUUUAAAAAUCAAGGAGAUUGUACAGAACUUUGUGAUUUUAAUUACUGCAUGGCAAACUAAUUCAGUCUCAUAUCCUUUCCAUUUAAUAGGGAUUUGUCCCUAGCUAUGUGACCUAAGCAAGCUCUUUAACUGUACUCCACCUCAAUUUGCUUAUCUGUAAAACAUGGAUAAUAUUAUUUUUAGUCUAAAACUUCCUCUGGUAUGACAGAAAAGACCAAUGUGAAACAAUUCCCUGAAUUUGUCAAUAAACCAUGUUACAUUUAUAAAAAUGCCUCCAGUGUACCCAGACCAGAGGAAUCUGUGGCUUAUACUAAAACGUGUAUUAUGUAUUCAUUCUCAAGGUAUAUGCCAACAGUUAAGUUAGAAAUCCAUCCCUUUCUCUGUCACUUGUCCAAAGUCAAUUACUCCAUGCUUCUUUUACAUAAGGAAAACUAUCUUAAAAGGAGGAAGUAAGAUCACGGACAAACAAAAGUUCAUAAGGUCUUUCAUUUUACUGCCUUUCAAAAGGUUAAGAUCAGAGAACUUAGACAUGCAUAAGCUUUGGUUUGAGGAACAAUUGAGUCAACCAUCGUAACAGAGGGCCUGAAAGUAUCUGAAGGUAGAAUGAAUAGUUUAUAGUAAGCCAGUCCACUCUCAGCUCUGAGAACAUCCAGCUGCAUAACCUCAAGGGAACUGCGUGGAAAAAAUUAAGGGAAAUUCUUUGGGCUUUAGAGCUUUUCAUUUCCUAUGAACAAGGCAUCUCCUGCCCUUGUCUCACCCAUAUCUCCAUUGUCCUCAUGUAGUCUUCUGCUGGUUCACUGUGUGCCUGGCAAGUCAGGUUCUUACGCGAGGGAAAGAGCUGUUUUAAGUUGUUUAUGAAUAGAGAAAGCAGAUUCAGUCAGACGUAAUCUGACUCUGUAUGCCUGCAGGGGUUGUGGCCUUUGUUAGUUUAUUAUGCCUGUAAUUUGGGAAGUCAUGCUGCAGAGAUGUAAAGUGGGAUGGGCCUGAAAUAGGUCUUGUAAUAAAAAGGCAGUUAGGGAAGCCUGCUGGUGUCCUGCCUGGUUACUACUAUCUAAGUGCAGCAAUGUGUUAGUUGAUUUUAAUAAAGAGUUGAAAUCAUUGUUAACUGGCCUCCCUCCCACUGAGUGAAGAAGGCAGAUUACACAGGCACACGUUUGCCUCCCCUAGUGUGUACUAUGAAUGCAGCUGCUUCUGAAGGGCCAGCACGUGGCCUUCUUAAAACUUUCCUUGGCUGGGGUUUUCCCUUCUUGCCAACUGGUGCCCACCAAGCCAGUGGAUGCUCUCAACGUCUAGGCAAAUGCCAAAAAUGUCAUCUUUGGCUCAGAUGUGCACUGGCCUGUUAGAGACAACUGCCAUGCAGAGAAGGAAUGUCAUCAGCUGCUAGGUCUCAAAUUAUCAGCCUGGAUUGACAGCUGCAGGAUGUAGUGCCUGCCUAUAGUACUGAGGCCAUGACCCACCUCUGGAGAGACCACAGCCUCAUCCCUAGAGUAGAACUGGAAAUUCUCCAUUGAGACAGGAAGGCAGCACUUGAACCUGGCAGGUUUUGGAGUGAAGUGUCUAAGGACAGAAUUUCUCAUUUCUCCACCUCUGCCCAUGUGUAAGGCAGCAAUAUUUUCAUAGAGGUGAAGAAGGCAGGUGUCCCGUGGUUAUUAUGACAUCUGUUUACCUCAUUCUAGUCACUGUGCCAUGUUUCACAGCCAUUGUCAACUACAUUUGGUGAAAACUGUUUCCUCCGUCCACAACUGGAACAUUGACACUAACCACAUUCUAGAGUUCAUUACAUAGAGCUGUGUCUGUGGUUUUGAUGUGGACAAUGGCACAUCUGCGGGACGGAGUCCCUUGGAUCCCAUGACCAGCCCAGGAUCCGGGCUAAUUCUCCAAGCAAAUUUUGUCCACAGUCAACGACGGGAGUCCUUCCUGUAUCGAUCCGACAGCGAUUAUGACCUCUCUCCAAAGUCUAUGUCCCGGAACUCCUCCAUUGCCAGUGAUAUACACGGAGAUGACUUGAUUGUGACUCCAUUUGCUCAGGUCUUGGCCAGUCUGCGAACUGUACGAAACAACUUUGCUGCAUUAACUAAUUUGCAAGAUCGAGCACCUAGCAAAAGAUCACCCAUGUGCAACCAACCAUCCAUCAACAAAGCCACCAUAACAGAGGAGGCCUACCAGAAACUGGCCAGCGAGACCCUGGAGGAGCUGGACUGGUGUCUGGACCAGCUAGAGACCCUACAGACCAGGCACUCCGUCAGUGAGAUGGCCUCCAACAAGUUUAAAAGGAUGCUUAAUCGGGAGCUCACCCAUCUCUCUGAAAUGAGUCGGUCUGGAAAUCAAGUGUCAGAGUUUAUAUCAAACACAUUCUUAGAUAAGCAACAUGAAGUGGAAAUUCCUUCUCCAACUCAGAAGGAAAAGGAGAAAAAGAAAAGACCAAUGUCUCAGAUCAGUGGAGUCAAGAAAUUGAUGCACAGCUCUAGUCUGACUAAUUCAAGUAUCCCAAGGUUUGGAGUUAAAACUGAACAAGAAGAUGUCCUUGCCAAGGAACUAGAAGAUGUGAACAAAUGGGGUCUUCAUGUUUUCAGAAUAGCAGAGUUGUCUGGUAACCGGCCCUUGACUGUUAUCAUGCACACCAUUUUUCAGGAACGGGAUUUAUUAAAAACAUUUAAAAUUCCAGUAGAUACUUUAAUUACAUAUCUUAUGACUCUCGAAGACCAUUACCAUGCUGAUGUGGCCUAUCACAACAAUAUCCAUGCUGCAGAUGUUGUCCAGUCUACUCAUGUGCUAUUAUCUACACCUGCUUUGGAGGCUGUGUUUACAGAUUUGGAGAUUCUUGCAGCAAUUUUUGCCAGUGCAAUACAUGAUGUAGAUCAUCCUGGUGUGUCCAAUCAAUUUCUGAUCAAUACAAACUCUGAACUUGCCUUGAUGUACAAUGAUUCCUCAGUCUUAGAGAACCAUCAUUUGGCUGUGGGCUUUAAAUUGCUUCAGGAAGAAAACUGUGACAUUUUCCAGAAUUUGACCAAAAAACAAAGACAAUCUUUAAGGAAAAUGGUCAUUGACAUCGUACUUGCAACAGAUAUGUCAAAACACAUGAAUCUACUGGCUGAUUUGAAGACUAUGGUUGAAACUAAGAAAGUGACAAGCUCUGGAGUUCUUCUUCUUGAUAAUUAUUCCGAUAGGAUUCAGGUUCUUCAGAAUAUGGUGCACUGUGCAGAUCUGAGCAACCCAACAAAGCCUCUCCAGCUGUACCGCCAGUGGACGGACCGGAUAAUGGAGGAGUUCUUCCGCCAAGGAGACCGAGAGAGGGAACGUGGCAUGGAGAUAAGCCCCAUGUGUGACAAGCACAAUGCUUCCGUGGAAAAAUCACAGGUGGGCUUCAUAGACUAUAUUGUUCAUCCCCUCUGGGAGACAUGGGCAGACCUCGUCCACCCUGACGCCCAGGAUAUUUUGGACACUUUGGAGGACAAUCGUGAAUGGUACCAGAGCACAAUCCCUCAGAGCCCCUCUCCUGCACCUGAUGACCCAGAGGAGGGCCGGCAGGGUCAAACUGAGAAAUUCCAGUUUGAACUAACUUUAGAGGAAGAUGGUGAGUCAGACACGGAAAAGGACAGUGGCAGUCAAGUGGAAGAAGACACUAGCUGCAGUGACUCCAAGACUCUUUGUACUCAAGACUCAGAGUCUACUGAAAUUCCCCUUGAUGAACAGGUUGAAGAGGAGGCAGUAGGGGAAGAAGAGGAAAGCCAGCCUGAAGCCUGUGUCAUAGAUGAUCGUUCUCCUGACACGUAACAGUGCAAAAACUUUCAUGCCUUUUUUUUUUUUAAGUAGAAAAAUUGUUUCCAAAGUGCAUGUCACAUGCCACAACCACGGUCACACCUCACUGUCAUCUGCCAGGACGUUUGUUGAACAAAACUGACCUUGACUACUCAGUCCAGCGCUCAGGAAUAUCGUAACCAGUUUUUUCACCUCCAUGUCAUCCGAGCAAGGUGGACAUCUUCACGAACAGCGUUUUUAACAAGAUUUCAGCUUGGUAGAGCUGACAAAGCAGAUAAAAUCUACUCCAAAUUAUUUUCAAGAGAGUGUGACUCAUCAGGCAGCCCAAAAGUUUAUUGGACUUGGGGUUUCUAUUCCUUUUUAUUUGUUUGCAAUAUUUUCAGAAGAAAGGCAUUGCACAGAGUGAACUUAAUGGACGAAGCAACAAAUAUGUCAAGAACAGGACAUAGCACGAAUCUGUUACCAGUAGGAGGAGGAUGAGCCACAGAAAUUGCAUAAUUUUCUAAUUUCAAGUCUUCCUGAUACAUGACUGAAUAGUGUGGUUCAGUGAGCUGCACUGACCUCUACAUUUUGUAUGAUAUGUAAAACAGAUUUUUUGUAGAGCUUACUUUUAUUAUUAAAUGUAUUGAGGUAUUAUAUUUAAAAAAAACUAUGUUCAGAACUUCAUCUGCCACUGGUUAUUUUUUUCUAAGGAGUAACUUGCAAGUUUUCAGUACAAAUCUGUGCUACACUGGAUAAAAAUCUAAUUUAUGAAUUUUACUUGCACCUUAUAGUUCAUAGCAAUUAACUGAUUUGUAGUGAUUCAUUGUUUGUUUUAUAUACCAAUGACUUCCAUAUUUUAAAAGAGAAAAACAACUUUAUGUUGCAGGAAACCCUUUUUGUAAGUCUUUAUUAUUUACUUUGCAUUUUGUUUCACUCUUUCCAGAUAAGCAGAGUUGCUCUUCACCAGUGUUUUUCUUCAUGUGCAAAGUGACUAUUUGUUCUAUAAUACUUUUAUGUGUGUUAUAUCAAAUGUGUCUUAAGCUUCAUGCAAACUCAGUCAUCAGUUCGUGUUGUCUGAAGCAAGUGGGAGAUAUAUAAAUACCCAGUAGCUAAAAUGGUCAGUCUUUUUUAGAUGUUUUCCUACUUAGUAUCUCCUAAUAACGUUUUGCUGUGUCACUAGAUGUUCAUUUCACAAGUGCAUGUCUUUCUAAUAAUCCACACAUUUCAUGCUCUAAUAAUCCACACAUUUCAUGCUCAUUUUUAUUGUUUUUACAGCCAGUUAUAGUAAGAAAAAGGUUUUUCCCCUUGUGCUGCUUUAUAAUUUAGCGUGUGUCUGAACCUUAUCCAUGUUUGCUAGAUGAGGUCUUGUCAAAUAUAUCACUACCAUUGUCACCGGUGAAAAGAAACAGGUAGUUAAGUUAGGGUUAACAUUCAUUUCAACCACGAGGUUGUAUAUCAUGACUAGCUUUUACUCUUGGUUUACAGAGAAAAGUUAAACAGCCAACUAGGCAGUUUUUAAGAAUAUUAACAAUAUAUUAACAAACACCAAUACAACUAAUCCUAUUUGGUUUUAAUGAUUUCACCAUGGGAUUAAGAACUAUAUCAGGAACAUCCCUGAGAAACGGUUUUAAGUGUAGCAACUACUCUUCCUUAAUGGACAGCCACAUAACGUGUAGGAAGUCCUUUAUCACUUAUCCUCGAUCCAUAAGCAUAUCUUGCAGAGGGGAACUACUUCUUUAAACACAUGGAGGGAAAGAAGAUGAUGCCACUGGCACCAGAGGGUUAGUACUGUGAUGCAUCCUAAAAUAUUUAUUAUAUUGGUAAAAAUUCUGGUUAAAUAAAAAAUUAGAGAUCACUCUUGGCUGAUUUCAGCACCAGGAACUGUAUUACAGUUUUAGAGAUUAAUUCCUAGUGUUUACCUGAUUAUAGCAGUUGGCAUCAUGGGGCAUUUAAUUCUGACUUUAUCCCCACGUCAGCCUUAAUAAAGUCUUCUUUACCUUCUCUAUGAAGACUUUAAAGCCCAAAUAAUCAUUUUUCACAUUGAUAUUCAAGAAUUGAGAUAGAUAGAAGCCAAAGUGGGUAUCUGACAAGUGGAAAAUCAAACGUUUAAGAAGAAUUACAACUCUGAAAAGCAUUUAUAUGUGGAACUUCUCAAGGAGCCUCCUGGGGACUGGAAAGUAAGUCAUCAGCCAGGCAAAUGACUCAUGCUGAAGAGAGUCCCCAUUUCAGUCCCCUGAGAUCUAGCUGAUGCUUAGAUCCUUUGAAAUAAAAAUUAUGUCUUUAUAACUCUGAUCUUUUACAUAAAGCAGAAGAGGAAUCAACUAGUUAAUUGCAAGGUUUCUACUCUGUUUCCUCUGUAAAGAUCAGAUGGUAAUCUUUCAAAUAAGAAAAAAAUAAAGACGUAUGUUUGACCAAGUAGUUUCACAAGAAUAUUUGGGAACUUGUUUCUUUUAAUUUUAUUUGUCCCUGAGUGAAGUCUAGAAAGAAAGGUAAAGAGUCUAGAGUUUAUUCCUCUUUCCAAAACAUUCUCAUUCCUCUCCUCCCUACACUUAGUAUUUCCCCCACAGAGUGCCUAGAAUCUUAAUAAUGAAUAAAAUAAAAAGCAGCAAUAUGUCAUUAACAAAUCCAGACCUGAAAGGGUAAAGGGUUUAUAACUGCACUAAUAAAGAGAGGCUCUUUUUUUUUCUUCCAGUUUGUUGGUUUUUAAUGGUACCGUGUUGUAAAGAUACCCACUAAUGGACAAUCAAAUUGCAGAAAAGGCUCAAUAUCCAAGAGACAGGGACUAAUGCACUGUACAAUCUGCUUAUCCUUGCCCUUCUCUCUUGCCAAAGUGUGCUUCAGAAAUAUAUACUGCUUUAAAAAAGAAUAAAAGAAUAUCCUUUUACAAGUGGCUUUACAUUUCCUAAAAUGCCAUAAGAAAAUGCAAUAUCUGGGUACUGUAUGGGGAAAAAAAUGUCCAAGUUUGUGUAAAACCAGUGCAUUUCAGCUUGCAAGUUACUGAACACAAUAAUGCUGUUUUAAUUUUGUUUUAUAUCAGUUAAAAUUCACAAUAAUGUAGAUAGAACAAAUUACAGACAAGGAAAGAAAAAACUUGAAUGAAAUGGAUUUUACAGAAAGCUUUAUGAUAAUUUUUGAAUGCAUUAUUUAUUUUUUGUGCCAUGCAUUUUUUUUCUCACCAAAUGACCUUACCUGUAAUACAGUCUUGUUUGUCUGUUUACAACCAUGUAUUUAUUGCAAUGUACAUACUGUAAUGUUAAUUGUAAAUUAUCUGUUCUUAUUAAAACAUCAUCCCAUGAUGGGAUGGUGUUGAUAUAUUUGGAAACUCUUGGUGAGAGAAUGAAUGGUGUGUAUACAUACUCUGUACAUUUUUCUUUUCUCCUGUAAUAUAGUCUUGUCACCUUAGAGCUUGUUUAUGGAAGAUUCAAGAAAACUAUAAAAUACUUAAAGAUAUAUAAAUUUAAAAAAACAUAGCUGCAGGUCUUUGGUCCCAGGGCUGUGCCUUAACUUUAACCAAUAUUUUCUUCUGUUUUGCUGCAUUUGAAAGGUAACAGUGGAGCUAGGGCUGGGCAUUUUACAUCCAGGCUUUUAAUUGAUUAGAAUUCUGCCAAUAGGUGGAUUUUACAAAACCACAGACAACCUCUGAAAGAUUCUGAGACCCUUUUGAGACAGAAGCUCUUAAGUACUUCUUGCCAGGGAGCAGCACUGCAUGUGUGAUGGUUGUUUGCCAUCUGUUGAUCAGGAACUACUUCAGCUACUUGCAUUUGAUUAUUUCCUUUUUUUUUUUUUUUAACUCGGAAACACAACUGGGGAAAUAUAUUCUUUCCCAGUGAUUAUAAACAAUCUUUUUCUUUUUUUUAAGUCCUUUUGGCUUCUAGAGCUCAUAGGAAAAUGGACUUGAUUUGAAAUUGGAGCCAGAGUUUACUCGUGUUGGUUAUCUAUUCAUCAGCUUCCUGACAUGUUAAGAGAAUACAUUAAAGAGAAAAUACUGUUUUUUAAUCCUAAAAUUUUUCUUCCACUAAGAUAAACCAAAUGUCCUUACAUAUAUGUAAACCCAUCUAUUUAAACGCAAAGGUGGGUUGAUGUCAGUUUACAUAGCAGAAAGCAUUCACUAUCCUCUAAGAUUUGUUUCUGCAAAACUUUCAUUGCUUUAGAAUUUUAAAAUUUCACCUUGUACAAUGGCCAGCCCCUAAAGCAGGAAACAUUUAUAAUGGAUUAUAUGGAAACAUCCUCCCAGUACUUGCCCAGCCCUUGAAUCAUGUGGCUUUUCAGUGAAAGGAAAGAUUCUUUUUCUAGGAAAAAUGAGCCUAUUUUAUUUUAUUUUAUUUUAUUUUUUGACACAAACUGUAGAUUUUAGCAGCCCUGGCCCAAAGGAAUUUGAUUACUUUUGUUUUAAACAGUACAAAGGGGACACUAUAAUUACAAAAACAUCCUUAACUGAUUUGAGUUGUUUUUAUUUCUUUGGAUAUAUUUUCAGAGUGGUAAAUUGUGUGUGAGAAUUACAAAUGAUUAUUCUUUUAGUGGUUUCUUAGCCUCUCUUACAGCCCACGGGGAUAGUACUGUACAUCAAUACCUUCAUAUGAAAUUUUUAUAUGCAAUGAAAAUAAAAGCAUGGGUUGAUUCUGCCUAUUUAUGACUCAAUCUUUUACAAAUAAAAGAUUAUUCAUUUUAAAUUAUAGUUCAAUCAGCAUGUCUCUUAGGAUACUGAACGUGGUUGAAAUGAAAGGAUAGUGACAUCAUAAGUUAGUACUGAUAUUCAUAACCAAAUAAAGCCAACUUGAGUAAUUUUGCUACAUUAAAAAUUACCAAAAUUACUUAGAUGGCCUAUAAGAUUAAGCAUGGUGUUUUCUAAGCAAGCUUUGAAAGGGGCCUUCCAUACUUACUUAAUUGAAUAUUCUGGGAUAUUGAAAAUUAUUCAGAUACUUGACAAUUAUUUUUGGUUACCUACUCCGCAAACUACAAAGUUUUAAGGACUCAACAAUAAGUUAAUGAGACACAGUGUUUGCUUUCAUGGAGCUUACAGUCUGGAGGGGACAAAGGCUUAAACAAUACUCAUAUAAUUAUAUAUGUGAUCAGUACAAUGAAGGAGCUCAGUGGGGUAAAUAAGCAGGAACCUGAACUUGAUCUGUUCCGGAGGGCCACAGAAGGCUUCCUUGAGGCCUUGAGAAAGUGAUUUGCAUCUGAGUUCUGAAGGAUUGUAAGAGGUAACUAGGGAAAAAGUUGACAGGAAGAGGAAGGGGAUCCAGACAAGAAACAUUUGCAAAGAUCUUGAGGCAUAAAUGAGCUUGAGACAUCUGGAGAAACUGAGGAAAAGUGAGAGAGUAGGCAGGGCCUGGAGCCGCAGAGCCAUUGCUAACCAUCCUGUGUGAGAUAUCCCCCAUUCUGUAGCUUUAUUCUCAUAACCCUGCUCAAUUUUCUUUAUAACACUUCUCACAGAUUUAUAUACGUGUUUGUUUUUGUUAUCUGUCUCUCCCACCAGACCACAGCUCCAUGAGAGCAAGGUCUUUGCUUACCAAUAUAUCACUAGCACUUAAAACUAUGCCUGGUACACAGUAGGUUCUUAAUAUGUGUUGAAUAUAGCCAUCAAAUUGAUAUUGGAUAUAAUUCAAUCUGAUAAGAUAUUUUGAGAUAUUAAAGAGUUUUUAACUUGAUACCAUAAAAA